AUCUGUUUCUUUCUACCCCAGGCCCAUUCCCAUCAUGAGUAUUUAUUCUGCCCAGUGUGGGAUGGGUUCUGUUCUAGAAGUUUGCAUGAGCAGAGGGAAGCUUAGCCCCAUGAGGCCAGUCAUGAGGCUCCAUCUUAUUCUAUAGGCUUCAGCCUUUUUAUGAAGACCUAGCUUCUACUCUUGCCCCAGGCCCUAAGCAGGCCCAGACUUUUCCCAUAUACACACACUCUCUCUCUAACUUAUGUGUCUUACAUCUUAAUAAGGCAGCAGAUUGUAUCAGAAUCAGUUAACUCUUUAUCAAAAAACCCAGAGCAGACAGACGGGUGAACUUGCUCAUGGGCUGAGCUAGAAGGGAGGCCACUUUUCCUUCACACAGCCUCGGACUCUCCCUGGGCUUUUUUGUGUGUGCUGCGUGGAGACUGUGUUCUAACAUUUCAGUCAUAUCUUCCUUAUUUUAAAACUACAGAAUUGAUCUUACCAACUUACUGGGGAGCACGUCGUCAGUAAAUUCUAAUGGAAAAACCUGUCUGAUCAAUGGGACAGGAAAGCGUCACAGCAAUACCGGUGAGUCAUUCCAAGACCAGGCACAUUUGAGCUGUGUUGCUUCUUCGAUGCUGACUAUAAUUCUCCCUCAGCAUUACGUCGUCUUAAGCAGCUUUUGAAUCUUCGUCUCUGAUUCCCUUUCUAGGUCAGACUGUGUCUUUUUUUAAAAUUGUGCCUGGAUAUCCCCUUAAUAGGUUGGACAAGUCCCGUUAGGAUAAUUGGCUGUAUGAAUAUGCGAAAAUAGCAACAGUGAAUUUUAAAGUUCUUGAAUAGUCUCCCCGUCCCACUGUGAGGUGAGGCAUCUGGGGUGGGCUAUCUGUUUUUUGAUUCUUGGUUCUUGUUUUUAAAAAAAUAGGAUGUUGGACCUUGGGAUGAGAGGGAAGUAAAACAGUUUUGGAACCCUUUUAGAAAGCAAACUAAGACAAAACUCCUUUCUUGAGAAAAAUGGAUGGACAUUGUAAAGAAGACAGUAGGGCACCAGGAAGCCUUGAGCCAGGUCUGCCUGUGUCACAUUUCGAGUUAUGAGCUUCACCGCUCUGCUGUCUGUCUCUGGAGAUCAUCAUCAAACCCCUUUCUCUGAGUUGUUGAAUGGCUCAGAUGAGUUAAUGCCUAUGAAAGUACUCUGUAAACAGAAAAAUACCUUCCUAUUUGUAAUCUCAACAAAGGGACUUUUAUCAUCCCUAAAACAGAACAGACAUUUCUUUUUCAAUUAUGAAAGUUACAUAGACUCUUUUUAAAAAGUUAAAUGCACAAAAGUAUGAUGAAAAUUAAAAUAACCCUAAUGAGUCCAUCAUCCAGGGACAUCAUUGUUCUAAUUUAAACAUUUGGGUAAUCUGUUCUCUUUUUUUAAGAAGGGUUGUGUGUGUUUAUUUUUUUUCUUUUUUUGUGUGUGUUUGUGUAUAUCUAUGUGUAUUUUUAUUCUGUUUUCUUUACAUAACACUGUAUUGUAAACAUUCCCAAAAUGUAAAUUUUAAUCAUUGCAUAAUAUUGCAUUAUCUGAUAUAUGCACAUGCAUUUUGAGAUUUUGUGACGAACGAUUGUGACUAUUGUUUCCAUAAUUAAGGGUUAGCUGCUUACCAAGAAAGGAACUUACUUUAAAACAUGGCAGGCACACUUGGCCAUUUUUUUUUUUUUUUUUUUUUGGCAGUAAAGGAAUUUGAAGUAUCCAGUUUUUUAAAUAAAUUAAUAUGUAUUGAAUUGGAGUUUAGCAGUACUUUUAGUUAAGAUCUCAGUUAAGGUAAAAAGGUCAGACCUGUAGAGUUAUUAAUUUGUAGAAAAUUCUGACUACAGCAAAACAUAUUAGCCCAAGUUCUCUUUAUUAAUAAAACAUUAGUUACAGAAAUACUAAAAAAUAGAUUGGUUGGUCUCCUGAAUGUCCUGCGUUAGGUAAGUUGCCUUAUGCCAUCUGGAAGACUUUUUAUUUUCUCUUCAUAGAAGGAUACAAUAGAUUUGUUUUGCUCAAAGAGUUCAUUUUCUGUUGCUGGGCACAUAUAUAAUACUGUAAACACAUUUCUGGAUAUGACGACAUAAUGAUGAAGAGAGACCUUUGAAUAUUUUCUUAAAUGAAGAUUGAAGGAGUAGUAAGCUGUGAGAGGAGAUUUUUCUACUAUUUCAGUCCUAAGAUUGAUCUUUUUUGUCAUGGAUUUAUCCCUUUGUCUCUAUGCAUUUCUAUGUGUCUGCUCAGCAUCUUAUCUUCUACAUUUGCCCUAGUUCCAUCCUUCCUUUUUUCCAUGCUUGUUUUUCCAUACACCUGCCCAUCCACCCUCCUGCCUCUCUAUCCAGUCGUCCGUCUAACCAUUUCUGGCAAUUCUUACCUCCCUGUUUCAUGUAUAUCUCUCCAUUUUUACCUGUCAUUUAUAUUUAUCUAUUUGCCUAUCCAUAUCUACACCUGCUUGUCUGCUCACUGUCUAUCUAUAAAGUUAAUGGAGAUGAUUUUGAUGAAAACUUAUGAAUUUCUUUAUUGCAUUUUACACUGUGGGUUACAGGGGCCAAAGGCCAUGGGGACCAGAAAGUGGAAAUAACCAGAGCUCGGCCAUUUUUGUUUCAUUUCAAAAUCAGGAGGGAAGGUCAGAACUAACCUGAUUAUCCUUUCUGUGAUGCUAAUCAGGAUGUUCUUAGUAUAAUGCCUUUUGGAGACUGUUAUUUUAAGGAAUGUUUUGCUAAGAAUCAGUUGCCAGGACAUAGAAUGAAGAGCUAUUGUAUAGCUUCAGAGUAGUUCUCUUUUAAGAAGGAUAUAAUAAAUUAAAAAUAAUUUUCUUGAGGUCAGACUAAGGAAAAGUCAAAGAUAUACAAUUGCCAUCUCUCCAAAUUUAUUGAUUUUAUUUAUUUAUUAUUUAUUAUUAUUAUUAUUUGAGACAGAGUCUCACUUUGUUACCCAGGCUGGAGUGCAGUGGCACGAUCAUAAUUCACUGCAACCUCAAUGUCCUGGAGUCACUGAAGCCUCUCAAGUACCUUGGACUACAGUUGUGUGCCACAAUGCCCAGCUAAUUUUUUUUGUACUUUUUUUAAAGACAGUAUUUUGCCAUGUUGCCCAGGCUGGUGUUGAACUCCCGGGCUCAAACUAUCUGCUUGCCUUGGCCUCCCAAAGUGCUGGGAUUAUAAGUGUUAGCCACUGUACCCAGCCCAAUUUACUGACUUAAAAAAAAAGAAAAAAAAAACAACAACCCAGAACAUAUUGUAACAUUCUCAGGGAGUUUAGAGACAACAUAAUGAAGGUAUUUUCAAGGUUUGGGGAGCUGCUUGGAACUUGAUUUUGGACAAAAUGGAAGGAAAACAACCAUCCUUUACUGAAAACCAUUUUUCUUCUGAUUCUGAGAAAGCUGCUUUGCAUUUACUCUCUCGUUUAAUUCUCCCAUCCUUCCUUCAAUGUAAUUUCUAUUAUCCCAAUUUAUAACUAAGAAACAGAGACUCAAAGAGGCUAAAUGAUUUGCCUAAGUUUACAUGAUUAAUGAGUGCCACAGUUUUUGUGGAACAGAGACUUGUUUGAAUCUAAAACUGUUACUCUUUGCAGUAAACCACAAUGAAACCUUAGCUAUAUAUCAGUUCUCCACUUUAAAUUUUAUGGUAACUCAACCUCUGAAAAGGAUCCUGCAAAUAGCACAGUUUUCAGUUCUUUUCUUGAGAGAAGGCAGGGCUUUCAUAUGGACAUGAUAAAGAAGACAGCUCUUAGGAUGUGGAUAUAAGAUUGCAUUUAUGAACUUUACUUUAGUAUUUGACAGAAUGGGGUUUUCCUCACAUGCUGCUGUGUGUUUUUGUUUAACCUAAUCUGAGUCUCAUUAGGCAGCUUGAUCCAGAAGACAGAAAGGUCUCCUCCACAAGAUGCACCUUAUGAAGCAAACAAACCAAUGAAAUGCAGUAACUCCCUUCAAACUUUUGUAAGCUCUGGAAAGCCAGAAAAGACAGCUAUUGUAAUAUAUUUUGCCAGGCCAGCUGUUAUCAUCACAAACAAGCCUGAAAUAGCAAUGACUUUUGAAAUCACAGCACAUUUAUUUACUUCUUAACUUUUCCAUAGGUUUGAAAGCUUGCUCCCUCCCUUUUUAUCAUGCUAAACUGUAGUUGCUAACAACAUUCUAUUCUGGGUGGGAAUUAGCUUUGGCAUAAUUAAGAAUGGAGAUGGGGGUGGAUAAAAGAGGUUCUGCCAAAGGACUUGUCUUAUAUGAUUUUAUUCUUACUUUUAAUCUGUUUUAUUCUUUAAGCAUGUAUUAACUGCCUACUACGUACUCAACACUGUGCUAUGUGGGAAAAAUAUACUAGAACAAGGGAUGGUCAACUUUUUCUGUAAAGGGACAGAUGGUACACAGCUUAGAUUUGUGGUCCAUAAGGUGUCUGUUGUAGCUACUCACUCUGCUCUUAGAUAAUACACGAAACACUCAAGACUCCACCAUAAACAAUACAUAAAUAAUUGCGUGUGAAUAUGUUCCAAUAAACUUUUAUUCACAAAAACAUGCAGUAGGCUGGAUUUGGUCUGCGUGCCACAGGUUGCCAGCACCUGUACUAAAAUGUCCCUGAAAAUAGAGAACUUUGUUUUGUUCAUUGGCUGUGUCACCAGUGCCUAGAGUAGUACCUGGCAUGGGAUAGGUGACCAGUAAAUAUUUGUUGAAUGAAUGAACUUAUAAAUGAAUGAAUGACUCAGACUCCUUCUCUGAUCUCUUCUAUACUUAAAGAGAGUACAAAGAACUGUGGGAGGUAAAAGGUACUUUCCUGGAAGAGAGAGUGUGGAGGGUCAUGGAAUCAGUUGGUAUUUGAGCUGGACCCUGAAGAAUAGGUAAGUAUAUGUCACCAGCGGUGGUAGGAGAAGCACACUGCAGGUAGGAGAAACAUGCAAAUAGGAUAAGAAGCAGGGCACUUGUGGUGAAUAAUGAGGAGAUCAGAUGUUUUAUAACAGGAGUUUCCUGACUUGCUUGAUCUUCAAAAUCACCUGUUAUUAAAAAUAGGUUCCCAGUACCCUCCCUGGAGAUUCUGAUUUUGUAAGACAGGGUUGGCCAAUGAUAAUUUACAAAAUAAAUAUUUGAAAAGGUGUAUGGCUUUGGAAAGUUAUACUGGAACCAUUUCUAAUGGGAAAUAAAGUUCUCACUUUUCUUAGUAAAAGGACUAGUAUCAACUAGUAAUUGCUGGACCUAUAAUUACCCUAUACCUUCUGUGCCAUAGAAUGGAGGAAGUGCCCUGGCGGAAAUCUACCCUACUUAACUGCCUGUCUUCAUACGUCCCCUGUUGAUGUUGUAGGAGUACCCCAGCCUUUAUGAUGGAACAGUGUGUAAUUUAGUCAGUAAAUUGUAGUCAUAUAAAUUAUAAUAAAUGUAUCAAAUUUGUAGCUACUAGCUUUGUUGCUUUUGAAUUUCUGGGUUGGCAAACCUCUCAGAGGGCAAAUAGAUUUAAAUGGCGUAAUAGAAAAUUUGCAUUCUCUUGCUGUACCUCCAAUUCAGAGUGUAGUGUAAUGCCCAGAUUUGUUUGUAGACUAAGAUCACUGGAAGGGCUGUAUAGUUUAAGCCUCUUUUUUAAUAAUGGGGGGAAAUCUGAAGCCUAAAAGGUGGGCAGGGACUUGCUCAAGUUCUGUCACCAAAUUAUUUUGGCAGAACCAGGAGUAUAAUGCGAAUGUUAAGUUACUAAAUUUAGUUUUCUUUUCAUGGUGCCAUGCCACAUGUAUCAAUAAAGUUCCUAAUUUACAUACUUUCUCUCCCCUUUAAAUCUCACAGCUUUUUGCUCAUAUACCUCUUGUGUACUGCUUACCAUAAAGUUAUAUCUUAAUAUCUUAUCCUGAACGAGUAGCCCACUGUUAUCCCAAAUAAAGGCUGAGCUCUGUUUCCCUGGAGAGCUUAACAUAUUUCCUGGCACUUAGCAUGUGUUCAGCAAAUAAUUGUAGACUUGAAAUAUCUUGAGCAUCUUUUCUUUUCCCAUGUGUUUUGACUCAAGUUCCUUUGCAGUUAUAUUGUCAGAAAAGUCAAGCUCUUCCAGAAUUGCUGAAAUACAAAGAUAAUUUCUCUUAAGCUUCCUUAAAAAAGUUGAAUUCCCUAUUAUGGCUGAGACCUUUCUUAACAGCUCUUCUGAUAGUUAAAUGUCAGUUGCUUCAAAAAAGAAAUGUCAUUAAAUUAUCAGGGAAAUAAAUUACAUAUUUAUUUGGGCUGAAAUAUUUUAAUUGACCACUUAAAAUAAAGAUAAUAGCAAAAGACUGAUACAUUUCCUAGCUUGCACAUUUCUCUCAAUUGCCAGGACUUUUUUGUUUAUAUCUCUUAGGAGAUUUCAUUUUUAUUUCUUCUGCAUUAUGGUUAUAUAUGUGCUUUUGACUCUCCCAGUGGGUGAUAAGUUCUUUGAAGUCAAUGUACUUAAAAAAAUUAAUCUCUAUAUACCCACAAAGCCUAGCUCUGUAGGAGCUAAAUACUAAAUAUAUUUACUUUAAAAAAAUUGUUAGGAAAAGGUCAGUGUUACCUUGAUUUCAGUGUUAUUUUGCAGCCCUCAAGUCAACAACCAUUUUACUGAACAUCCAGCUUUGUGCCUUUCUGUGAGCUUAACAUUGGUAGCAGGUGUGGAUUGGGACAUAAAAAAGUAAAUAAAACAUAGUUAAGUUGACAUAACCCAUAAGUAUAAUGUGAUGUGGAAAUCUGAGAUAGGUACAAAUAACCUGUACUAGAAUCUGGAGGCAGGUUAAUUCUGACAAGGUGAGUCCAGAGAGGCUCACAAAGUGUCAAUAUUUGAGAUGAGUUUUACUGGGUCUUGGUCUUCUAUUUCAGUUGCUGGUUUUGAUUUUUCUCAACGCAACACACACACAAACACACAGAUACACACACACACGCAAAGUGAUUUGUUUUCUUUUUAUAAUCUCUUUGACUAUAGACUUAAGAGAACUGCCUUUAUGUAAGAUUAAAGGAAAAGAGGAGCAGGUUUUAUUGUGUUAUUUGAAGGUUUUUCAGAGUCUGAAACACACAGCGACCGAAAGUAUUUGGGAUGGAUGAUGCCAGUAGUGUCAUGAAACAAAGUACGUUGGCCAGAGAGAGACAUAUACUAUUGUAAAUUAACGGUGUUCUUUUCCAAGGAUUUUCUCGUUUACCUGUUGUUGUCUUCAAUAGUUUAAUUACACUAAAUAUUCUCGUUGGUGCGGGGAGCAUAGUAUGGUGGAGGAAGUUUCAACUUUGAAGUCAGACAGUUCUGUUUCUGUACCUAACUUUUCACUUAUUGUAUAUGUGACUGAAGGCUGUUGCUUAUCCUCUCUAGGGUUGUUUCUUCAUCCUUGAAAAAUGUUGUGUUUUCUUUUUCUUUUCUUUUAUUUUUUUUGAGACGUAGUCUCACUCUUUCACCUAGGUUGGAGUGCAGUGGCGUGAUCUCGGUUUACUGCAACCUGUGCCUCCUGAGUUCAAGCGAUUCUCCUGCCUCAGCCUCCCAAGUAGCUGGGAUUGCAGGUGUGCACCACCAUGUCCAGCUAAUUUUUUUUUUUUUGUAUUUUUAGUAGAGACGGGGUUUCACCAUGUUGGUCAGGCUGGGCUUGAACUCCUGACCUCAAAUGAUCCACCCACCAUGCCCUCCCAAAGUGUUGGGAUUACAGGUGUGAGCCACCGUGCCUGGCCUGAAAAUUGUGAUCAUGGAAAGUACCUCACAGAAUUGUGGGAUGAAUGGAGCUAAUGUUUGCAAAGCUCCUAUUUCAGUGUCCAGGAUAUGUUAGGCCAUAUGCCUACAGAGUCAGGCACAUUUUCUUGAAACACAAAGCCCUUUAUCUAGCUUAACCUCUUCCCACUUUAGAGUCGUGGGUGCAGGAAAUAUUUUGUUUUCCUCUUUACCGUAAGGAAAGUAACAGUGCUAGUGUGUUGUUGAAAUGCCAUGCUCUGGGCAUGUGUUUGGGGAGAGAGAUGCAGUGCGUGGUGGGGAAUGGGAGGUGCUCAAGAGGGCAUCCUCUCUGAAAGGGGUGACAGCCGCUUGGCGCUAGCUAAUUAUUGCCACGUGGAGAUGCAUCAUUGCCAGAUUUUUAUGUAAACUCUUUGGUUUUUAAAAUGUUGGCAGCUCAUUCAAGUAUUUUUAAAGCACUAUGAGAGAUACUUCCUCAUGGAAGAAGAAAAAUGCAACUUACAAUCUUACUCAGUAGCAUCAACUUUGGCUCAAAACAACAACAAAGCACGUUGUAAGUCCACACUGCAAAUGGCAAACAGAACCCGUCUAAGGACCAGAUUUGGCCUGCAGCCCUCAAUUUGCAUCUUCUGUGCAUAUUUUUAACUGGUAGAGAUAACAGUAAAUGAUGGCAAAACUUACUGAGUCCUUUGCAUGUGCUAGAAACUUUGCUAUACUUUGCAUAUAUCAUUCAAUUCUCACAAUAACCCAAAGAGGUGUCUAUUACUAUUAUUAUCCCAUUUUACAGACGUGAGCAUUGAGGCUCAAGGAAAUGAAGUAUCUUUCCUGAGGUCACACAGAUGAAAUGUGACAGGUAGCUUUGAAACCAAAGCCUGUUCUCUUUUAAAAUCAUACAUACCAGUGGAUCUCAGUCCUGGUGGUAUGUUAGAAUGAUUGGCGUGCCCUUAAAAACAGUGUUGUCCAAAGUCCACCCCCAAGCUCAUUAAAUCAGAAUAUCUGUGGGUGGGACUCAGACGUGGCUGUUUUUUCGAAAGCCUCAAAUCAAUGAUUAGAAAUAGCUGUAAGAUAGAUAAAAUUUGUGCCUCCACAUCUGGCACUACCUAUCUCCUGUACUCUAUUUUAUUUUUGAGUAUUUAUUGUUCUCUGAAAAUUAUGUGCAUCUUUACCUGUUUAUGAAUUUUCUACUUUUACCACACUGGGAUGUAAGCUCCGUGAGCGCCAGGAUUUAGUCUUUUUAAGUUGUUUGUUGUAUCCCCACCUAGGUCAGUGCCUGGCACAUAAUAGAUGCUCAGUAAGUAUUUACUUGAAUGAAUAACUGGUUCUUCAUCACAGGGAGCUUACACUCUAGUGAGGGAGAUAGAUAAUACAUUCUUAGUCCUAUGAGAUAAGCUCAUAACUGGGAUGUUCAAUAUGACUUUAUUAACACAGGGAAUACAGCUGAUUAUCUCUUAGACAUUGUUAGGAUAAAUUGUUUCUAUACGUAUUGAAUGGACUGUGGGGCAUUUUUGGUCACCUGCACUACUACACUGGAUCCAUUCUGUGCUCUGGGGUGUAAGUGUGUGUGUGUGUCUGUGCGUGUGUGUAAUUUCGGGAACGGGUAACACAUUCGUAUUACCUCUGUUUGGACACGAUUUUUAGUGACAGAGCUAGGAAUAACAGGUGGAACCUUCUAAGUUUUGUUGCUUAAAUAUCAGGCCCCCUCAGAAUUCAGGACUGAUGGUAGAGGAUUUACCAGUUUACAGGGAAUUCAGAUAUUCUCUUCUCUUUCUAGGAAAGCCAAAUUGUUGGUCAUUCUGCCCCCAACAUUUACAGAAGCAGUUUCUCGGUUUUAUUUAUCCAAGAUUCUUAUGAUGAAUAGUGUUAAUAUCGCAGCACACUAUGGGCUGUGAUAUGCCUAUAUCACAGAGAAGGCAAGCUGUGGUGAAGUGGAAUAAAUGAAAAACUGUCUAUAACUCUGCUUCUAGAUGCCCCACUUAAGCAAGUAAAUGGGAAUGUGAGUGACAAUAUCAUAGGGAUAACCUUGAAAGAGUGCUAGUUUUUAAACAAAAACAAAUCAUUUGGAACGUUAGGAUUUAAACAGUUACUGAUAAUAAAUUGCUUGUGACCCAUCUGAAAAUUGAUGGAUCAUAGUGAUAGUGAAAAUAUUUAACAACUGCUAUGGCCCAGGCACCGAACAAUCGAAACCAACUCCAGUGUAAACAGUGGUGCCAUCAAGUAUGCGCUGGUUGUCAGCCUUGCUGGUGGAGUCAUUGUGUCACGAUGAAGCAACUAAGAGCCAGUGCUGCACAAAGUGUUGAGAGAAACAAACAAAAUCCAGGGUGCUCCCCUUAUGCGGAGUAGAGAGUAGAUAGAGCCUUGUUUCAGAACGAUAAAACUUCGGUCAAGGACUUGAUCUUCCCACUUAUUGCUGGGGGCUCCAGGGCAAAUCAUUUGUUCUUUCUGAGCCUGAGUUGUUGUUUCUUCUUGUUCUUCUUGUUCUUGUUCUUGUUCUCGUUCUCGUUCUCCUUCUCCUACUCCUUCUCCUUCUUCUUCGUCUUCUUCUUCUUCUCUCCUCCUCCUCCUCCUUCUCCCUUCUCCCUUCUCCUUUCUCCUUCUCCUCCUCCCUCCUCUCCUUCUCCUUCUUCUUUUUCUUCUUCUUCUUUUUUUUUUUUUUUUUGAUAUGGAGUCUCACUCUGUUGCCCAGGCUGGAGUGUAGUGGUGCAAUCCCUGCUCCUGCAUCCUCUGCCUCCCAGGUUCAAGCGAUUCUCCUGCCUUAGCCUCCUCAGUAUCUGGGAUUAUAGACGUGCAUGACCAUGCUCAGCUAAUUUUUGUAUUUUUAGCAGAGAUGGGGUUUCACCAUAUUGGCCAGGCUGGUCUUGAACUCCUGACCUCAGGUGAUCCACCUGCCUUGCCCUCCCAAAGUGCUGGGAUUACAGUCAUGAGCCACCGCACCUGUCCGGAGCCUGCGUUUCUUCUAAUAUACAGUGGAGGAGAGUAAUUUUUGCAUUACCUACUUUGCAGGCUCUGGAGUUAGAUUGAGCGCACCUGAAGCUAAGGUUAAAGAUGAUGGCUAUGGGCAUGAUGACAGUAAUUGUUCUUCUCUGGUUGGGGACUGAUUGAUGAUCCCUGAUUUCUCUGUUUAAACGUUGCCCAAAACAAAGGUUGAGAGGUCCUUAGGGGAGAGGCGAGAUAAGCAGAGGUAGGACUUGCCUUUCUUCUGUGCUUCUCCAGAAUUAGUUGUGUCCUGUGGCAUCCACAGACAAAAAUUGAGCAAUCUCCUUCAUAGUUGAGAUUGUAUAAUUCGAUAAAAUAGGUUUAAAUAGCCUUAUGCCUGUAUAAUAUUCAUGAAAAGUGUCAUGAGUGAGGUGGCUUGCUUGUUUUGAAAAUGGGCUGAUUUUGACAAAGGGGAAAAAUCGGGAUUCAUUUACUGUAAGUUGAAAGUAAGAAACAACAAAGUUGAAUAUUAGAAGAACUUGGCUAUCGCAAAAACCACAUACUUUCACAUCAGUAAAACAUGGAGUUCUGAUCUGAGUGAAAUGUGAAACUUCUUGCAGACCACAGAGAGUAAAAAGGAGUACUUUUGUUUCAUUAUUAAUACCAUUGUCCUUAUUUCUUUAAAUGAGAAUUGAUAAUACCCAUAACAGAAUCUUUCACACAGGCCAAAAACAGAAAGAUAAAUUAAACAAAACAAACAAACACCCAAAACCUCACCACCACCACCAUGACUGCCAACAAAACCCAGUGCUGUGAGGAUGCAUCAGCUUUAAGAUCUCUUUAAGUCAUUGUGUUCUAGAGAAAGGGGUUCUUUAUUUGUUUCUAUCAGGAUAGAGUGAGUUUUUGUUAAAGUUGUCUUUCUUUUUUUUUUUUUUUUCUUCUUCUGGAAGACUGACGAAGUUGGCCUUUUGGGAUAUUACAAGAAAGAUAACUUUGUCUUCUAAUGUCUGCAGUGAUAUGAGGCAGGUGACUGUGUGUAUUCUGUGGUGAUCCAUGUUCACAAGGAGAGACAGGCCAAGGAUGCCCGGUUGAUGAGUGCGCUAUAGGUGCUUGGGAGUGAGAAGGCAAGAAAGCAAAGUGAACUUAAAAAAUAGCUAGCCAGUGGAAUUGAGGGAGAAAUGCUCAUUCUUUGCUGACACAUGAAAUAAUUGUUGAGGGAGAGUUGCUCAAUCUUUGCCUACACAUUGAAAUAAUUGUGUUGAAGAGUCUAUGAAAAGGGGGUCAAUAGAUUUGAGUUUUCAUCACUUUGGCCACCACCUAAUUAUAGAUGGCCUCCACUGUGAAAUAUGUGAGUUGAAAUAGAUUUUUUUAAAAUUCAUUUUCUGGACUGGCAUUUAGAAUUUGAGUUUAUUCAAUCCUUGCUUCUUGGGCAGUUAGGGUGUCAAUGGCAAUAGGAAGGGUAGCUGAGGCCAGAGUGGUGGGGGUAGAUGUUGGGUGGAAUGUGUGUGGUUGAGCAGAGCAUUAUUAUUAUUGCUAUUAUUAUUUUUUAAAAGAAUCCUUAUAGUAAAGAGAGCCAACAUUGAUUGAAUAUAUGUUCCUUGCCAGAACUUGGGCUAAGUGCUUUAUUAUAAGUUAUCUUAUUUAAUUUUCACAGAGACCUGUUGAAGUGUAAGUUUUAGCUUUCUGUUUCACAGCUGUGGAAACUGAGGUGCUGAAAGGAUGAAGAACUUCCAAAAAGUCGAAGAUAUUAAGCAGCUGUAUUAGUCUUCAGAUCCUGAUAUCUUUCUCAUAGUUAUUCUGAUAUGCCGUAUUAAGUUGCAGAAUUGAGGCCGGGUGCAGUGGCCCCAAUUUUUUUUUUUUAGUUAUUCUUAUUUUCUAAUUAUUUUAUAUGCUCUCUCUCUCUCUCUCUGUCUACUGUCAAAUCCCGGCACUAUGGGAGUCUGCAGUGGGAGGAUCUCUUGAUGCCAGGAGUUUGAGACCAGACUGGGCAACAUAGUGAGACCCCAUUUCUACAAAAAAAUGAAAUAAAACAAUUAGUUGGUCAUGAUGGUGUACACCUGUAGUCCUAGCUACUCAGGAGGCUGAGGCAGGAACAUUGCUUGAGAGUUCAAGGCUGCAGUGAGCUAUGAUUGUGCUGCUAUACUCCAGCUUGGAUAAUGGAGCGAGACCCUAUCUCUAAACUAAACUAAACUAAACUAAACUAAACUAAACUAAACUAAACUAAACUAAACUAAAAGUAAGAUAAAAUAAACUUACGGAGUUGGAACAUUGCAGGCUAUCUAUCUGGCUUCCCUGCCCUGAAUUCAUCGUUCUCUUUGAUGUGCUAUUGUCCAACAUUUCUUUUUUUUUUCUGUUUUUUUUCUGUUUUCUGUCUUGCUGUCACCCAGGCUUGAGUGCAGUGGCCUGAUGUUGGCUCACUGCAACCUCCAUGUCCCGAAUUCAAGCGAUUCUCCUGCCUCAGCCUUCUGAGUAGCUGGGAUUACAGGCACCCGCUGCUAUGCCCGGCUAAUUUUUGUAUUUUUAGUAGAGACAGAGUUUCACCAUAUUGGCCAGGCUGGUCUCGAACUCCUGAGCUCAGAUGAUUCUCCUGCCUCGACUUCCCAAAGUGCUGGGAUUACAGGUGUGAGCCACCGCACCAGGCCUUUCCAACAUUUCUUUAAAGAAACUAAAAAUUAAUUUGAAUAAGUAACACAAAAAUAUAGUUUAAACUAUAGUAUAAAAUUCAAAACUAUGCAAUGACAAGUACAUCUUUAUUUUAUCUCUUUACUUCUCCCACCCAGAGGAAAGUAUAAGUUCUUUAUAUAUCCUUUUAGAAAUAAACUGGGUAUAAAUAAGCAUGUGUAUACACACACACACAGAAACACACACACAAACACACACAGAUAUGUAUUUAUAUUCCAGUGUAUAUAAAUACAUUUAUAUACAUGCCAUUUAUAUACACAUUUGCAUUUCUGUUAUUAGCGACUCUAAACACCAUUUGAAAUGAGCCGUACCCAUUUGUAAUUCCGUUUUCUGAACUGUCCUUCACUUCCUUUUCCAUUGGAUUGCUGAAUUUUUGCUUAUUGAUUUAUUACAGUUAAGAAAAUUAACUUGUAGUCUGUGACAGGAAUUGUAAUGCUUUACCAUUUUGCAUUUCUUUUUUAACUUGCAGAUUAAAAUAAAAAGUUUUAUAUAGUUAAUCCUUUUUUGAUUUUAUGUUUCUUUGAUUUUGUGUGAUGCCUAGAAAUGCCUUCCCCACUUUGUGAUAUUUAAAAAGAAAUUUCCAAUUUUUCUUCUAGUUAUUUCUUCUGCUCUUUCUCAAAUCUUUGAACCAUUGAAAUUUUAUUUUGGUAAAAAAUGUGAGGUUAGGAUUUAUUUUGAUAUUUUUCUGGAUCUGCAUUUCUAAACACUGUUUAUUGAGGAGUCCAUCUCUUUCACACUGAUUUGAAAAGCUACCUUUAUUGUAUAUUAAAUUUCUUAAUACUUAAGUAUUUAAUACUUAAGAACACCGUGGAAUACUAUGCAGCCAUAAUAAAGGAUGAGUUCAUGUCCUUUGUAGGGACAUGGAUGAACCUGGAAACCAUCAUUCUCAGCAAACUAUCGCAAGGACAGAAAACCAAAGACCGCAUGUUCUUACUCACAGGUGGGAAUUGAACAAUGAGAAUGCUUGGACACAGGAAAGGGAACAUCACACACUGGGGCCUGUCAUGGGGUUGGGGGACGGGGGAGGGAUAGCAUUAGGAGAUAUACCUAAUGUAAAUGACGAGUUAAUGGGUGCAGCAAACCAACAUGGCACAUGUAUACAUAUGUAACAAAUCUGCACGUUGUGCACAUGUACCCCAGAACUUAAAAUAUUAAAAAAAAGAAAAAAAAAAGAAUUUGCAUCUAUUUUUAGACUUUCUGUUCUAUUCAUCUGUCACUUCAUGUGUCAUUAUUAUGCUUUCAAUUAUUGUAGCUUUAUAAUAUGUUUUAUUAUCUGACAAAGAUUCCCCAUUCCUAUUAGUUUCUCUUUUUCAGAAAAUUUCUGGCUUUUAAUGCCUGUUUAUUUUUCAUUGACCUUUAUAAUGAACCUAUCUAGUUCUGGCUGGGCGUGGUGGCUCACGCCUGUAAUCCCAGCACUUCGGGUGGCUGAGGUGGGCAGAUCACUUGAGGUCAGAAGUUCAAGACCAGCCUGGCCAACAUGGUGAAACCCUAUCUACUAAGAAUACAAAAAUUAGCCAAGUGUGGUGGCGGGCACCUGUAGUCCCAGCUACUCGGGAGGCUGAGGCAGGAGAAUCGCUUGAACUGGGAGGUGGAGGUUGCAGUGAGCCAAGAUCCCGCCACUGCACUCCAGCCUGGGUGACAGAGUGAGACUCCGUCUCAAAAAAAAAAAAAAAUAAAAUAAAAUAAUGUAAAAAAGUUCUGUUGAUAUACUUAUGAGGUUUGCUGGGUUUAUUUGUUAGCAUUACAUGCUAUACAUUGUAAAAAUGUUGAUUCUUUUUCUUGGAAUACUAAUGCCUUUCCAUUUGUUGAAACCUUCUUUGAUGUUCCCAGGAGCACUGAGAUUUUUCUUCAUGUAGACCGUGCCUGUUUCUAAUAAGUUAAUUUUGUAGAUAUUUUCUACUUGCUCUAGUUAAUGUAAUUAUUUUCUAUUUCAUUUAAUUAUAUGUGUGUGUGCCUCUGUGUUUGGGGUCUGGAUUUCAGUACAUUGAUUUUCUGCUCAGCCACUUUACUGAAUUGUCUCAUUAUUUGAAUAAUUUUAGAUAAAUUUUUUUUGAGUUUCUAGUUAAGUAAGUAUAUUAUCUGCCAAUAAUUUAUCCUUUCUUUCCAAUUUUUACAACACUUAUAGCUUUCUUCUAACUGUACUAAUACCUCUAGAAUAGUAAAUAUUAAAUAACUGUGGUUGAGUAAAUGUCCUUCUUUUGUGUCUGAGUUUAAUGGGAAUGCUCAUAAUGUUCCCUGUUACUAGUGACAUUGGCUUUCGAUUUGAGAAAUGUAUUGUGUUGAAAAGUAUCCACACUUAUUUUGAUAGUGUUGUUAUUGUUGUUGUUUUAAUUGAGACUGGUUGUUAAAAGGUUAUCUAGCUUUUUUUUUUAAAGAAACUUUGAAAGUAAUCAUAUAUUCUAAAAAAAUUUUAUGUUUUUCUCUUUUGUCCUGUAAAUUUGCUGUAAUAUAUGAAUAAAAUUUUCAAACAUGAAAUCUUGUUAGUAUUCUUGCUAAAAUAAUUAUCAACUUGUUCAUUGUUUCUGUAUUAUAUAUUUUUAGUGUUGCUAGAUCCUAGAGAUCAUUAAUAUAUUAAUGAUCUGUGCUUCAAUUUUCAUAAGUGAGAUUAUUUGAAAAUUCUGUGUGUGUGUGUGUGUGAUCGAGACCAUCCUGACCAAAAUAGUGAAAUCUCGUCUCUAAUGAAAAUACAAAAAUUAGCUGGGCAUGGUGUCAUGCGCCUGUAAUCCCAGCUACUCGGGAGGCUGAGGCAGGAGGAUCGCUUGAACCCGGGAGGCAGAGUUUGCAGUGAGUGAGAUUGCGCCCCUGACUCCAGCCUGGCGACAGAGAGAGACUCCAUCUCAAAAUAAACAAACAAACAAACAAGGAAGCUUUUCUUUUUUCUUUAUUUUGAAAUAGUUUGAUAACAUUUACAUGGGUUAUUUCUUUAAAAUAUGGUAGAAUUCCCUUGUGAAAAUACCUUCACUUAUUGCCUUUUUUGGAGUGAAGAACGGAGUGAAGAAAGUUAUUUCUUUAAAAUAUGGUAGAAUUCCCUUGUGAAAAUACCUUCACUUAUUGCCUUUUUUGGAGUGAAGAAUGUGUUUGCUCUUUAAAAUUUUUUACAUUUUUUUUCUGUAGUAAUUGGACUAAUUAGCUUUUAUAUCUAUUCUGUGAUUACCUUUGUUAAAUUAUAGUUUUUUUAGGGAAGUCACCUAUUUCAAAUUCAUUUGCAUGGUGUAAAAUAAUUUCUCAUGAUUGUUUUCAUUUCCUCUGUAUUUAUGGUUAUAUUUCACAUUAUUAUUUAAAGUUUUAUGGAUUUCUGCUAUGUGUAUCCAUCUUUCUGGCUAAAGCAUCAGAGUUUAAUUUAUUAUUUAUUUAAAAAAUAGCUUUUGCAUUUAUGUGUUGGCUCUACCACUUUGUAAUUCUUUAUUUUCUCUUUAAAAUCUUCAAUAAUACCUUCUACUUUUUCUAGGUUUAUUUUGUUGUUUUUCUCAUUGUUUGAACUUGGCUCUUAAUUUCCAUAUUUUUAUUUCUGCUUUUUUAUUCAUAUAAAUAAGAUAUAAAUUUUCCUGUAAGAGAUGCUUAUUUGUAUGCCUUAAGUUUUGCUAAAUAGUGUUUUUAAUCUUAUUUUUUAGUUAUUUGACUAUGCACAGGUUCUUAAAAUCCCAGACCCAUUAGAAUGUAAGCUUUGUAGGGACAGGAACCUUGUCUGUUUAUUUAUUUUGGGUCUACCGUUGUGCCUGUCAUAUAUUUCUUAAGCACUUGCUAAUGUGCUUAAGAAAUGCUUUUGUGUGAAUAAAUAAAUCUCCAGGGAAUUAUGGAAUUUGUGGCUGAUUCAGUCCUGUAACUCUAGUUCGUUUCUGCCUCAUUUGGAUAUUCUCUCUAGGUAUCUACUAAUGUGUAGGAAUAAGAACAUAUUAGACAUGCUUCAAAUUACCUUUUUAGGUCAUGAUAUUAAUAGAUUUAUUUUAAAAGUCUACAUAGUUUUUCUCAAAUCAAGUAUACCUGGGUAAAAAUGUCUUUCUAAAGAUUAGCCUGUCUGGGCGCGGUGGCUUACGCCUAUAAUCCCAGCACUUUGGGAGGCCGAGGCAGGCAGAUCACCUGAGGUCAGGAGUUUAAGACCAGCUUGGCCAACAUGGUGAAACCUGAUCUCUACUAAAAAAAUACAAAAAAACCAGCCAGGCAUGGUGGCAGGCACCUGUAAUCCCAGCUACUCCGGAGGCUGAGGUAGGAGAACCAUUUGAACUCAGGAGGCGGAGGUUGCAGUGAGCCAGGAUCGUGCCAUUGCACUCCAGCCUGGACGAAAAGAGUGAAACUCUGUCUCAAAAAAACAAAACAAAACAAAAAAAAGAUUAGCCCAAUCUAUUUCUAGCUACUUGGGAGGUUGAGGCAGGAGGAUCACUUGAGCCUAGAAGUUUGAGGUUACAGUGUGCUAUGAUCAUGCUACUUCACUCCAGCCUGGGUGACUGACCAAGACCCUACUGGAAGAAAAAAAAAAUAAGAAUUGCUCAAGAAAAAAUACAGUUGAGUAGAAUUAGAAUGCUAGCAGUGUUGCAAUAGCAGAGAUCACAUGAUGCCCAUGAUGUUUGUGACCUUGGACACUUUAGGCUAAAUUUUGCACAGAAGCCCAAGUCCAGGAUAGAAAUGAUAACGAUGAACCUGCUGUAGUGCAGGGAAAGAUGCAGAGCUGGGGGGAAGCCCAAACCCCUACUGAUGGCCACUUUUUCUUCUGACCUCUUCCUAUGUCUCAUUUAAAAACCAGUAGCUUUACUUCGAAAACUCAAUUUUCAGAUGAGAAUCAAAACAAAAAUGCAAAGAAGGCAAAUGAUUCAUAAAAGUUGCUGAGUGAAUUAGAACUAUAAUGUGGGACAAACACUCCGCCUUUCUGUCUCUGCAGCUAGUGGUAUUUCCAGGUUCCCAGGGAACCUCCUGUCCCUUGCUCCACUGUGCAUUUUUAGAUGGACCUGAUAUUUGGUUACCUCCCUUGUCAGGCCCAACAAUCCUUGCUAAGGCACAGACUUGUGUAUUUGCUGAUCCCUGAGGGGAAAGCUGUGAUUCAGGCUCUGAAGUCUAAGAAUUGCAGACUUAGUUUCUUGUCUCCCGAUGAAACUGCUAAUCUGGGUGCCAAUGGUGUUUCUGCUACAUGGACACCUGCCCACACAGCAUGAUUAGAAAUUAUAAUGAUGACGACGAUGAGUCUUCCAGGACACCCACGUUCUUUGCAAGAUAUUUCUGCUAAUCGUUUCUACCAGAAUCAGUUGGAAAACUUUUUUUUUUAAGUUUUUUUUUUUUCUCUGUAUCUAAGUCAACCAAAAAUGCUGGUCUAAUUCAGGUAUAGAUUAAAGGUUUGUCCUCACCAUUAAUGGUGUGUUAUUAUUCAUGCAGGGCAUCCUAGAACCUUGGGCACAUAGUGUAAUGGAAAGCACGCUGGGCCAGGGAGAUGUGGAUUCAGGCUUGAGCAGUGCCAAAAAUUUUCGUUAUGGCCUUGGUAAAGGUGAUUUCCCAUCUCUGUGACUUUGUGUCUCCUUCUGUUAAAUGGGCAUUCAAAUCUUUUGUACCUAACUUAUUAGGGCCCUGAUAAUCAAAUUAGCCAAUAAGUAAGAAAAUGUUUUCUUAACCACACUGUAAAUUAAGAGGAUUCAUAUUGAAAUCACUUUUCCAUUAUUGCUGUCUUAGCCUGCUAAAGUUAUAUUUAGUGUAGUGCAACUAAGCAGGGUUGUGAGAGCUGGGAAGGUAGACUGUUGUAUUGGGCAGGGUCAGGGCAGAUAAAGGACCAAAAUAAUGCCUGAAAUGCUGUAUUAACCUGCUCUACCUUGAACUGCUGUCUUGAAUUGGGGGGAAAAAUGAAGCUCUGAGGGGAUGGUGCACAGGGAGAAAAGAGAGAAUCUCAGGAAUUGAAAGUCUCAAUGGAGAAGAGGUGGGAGAAGAAUAGGAGGCUAGAGUGAGGGCAUGUGAUCGUGGAGUACCGAUCUGGAGACAAGAGAAGAAAGUAGAAAAAUGCCAGCACUGUCUUUGGACCCUGUGUAUCUGGAGUGUGGGAGGACAGGCAGACACAAAUAGAGAGGCUCUAGGGAAAACAGCAUUCUCAUAGAAGAUCCUUCUCCACAAAAAGCCCUCCAAAUGUCCUCCAGGAGGGUAGAAGCUGGUUUUAAAGCUCCUCAGGGUCAGGAAGAUCCUUCUCUUAUUUUUCUUUGCAUCGUGCAGUUUAAUUUAGCACAGUACUUUGCUCACAGCACUUAAAAAAUUAUUCUGGGCCUUGCUUUUUAAUUUUAGGCCCAAAUACCUGAAAAAAUGUUCAGGAGGAAUUCUGAUAAGAAAGAGCUAACUUAGGCAAUUCCAUUUCUUUUUUUGGUUCACUGUUUCCUCAUCUGAAAAGUGUUGGGCUCCAUGACGUGGUUUCUAUGACACUCAGUACCUUUGUUGAAGAGAAAACAUUUUUCUAAAACUAGGAUUUCCAAAAAAACAAAAAAAAAAAAGAAAAACAAAACUCAUGAAUAUGUGGAUAUUUUUGUGAUAGUGAUGAAGGUUUGGGAAUGGAGUAGAAUGUUUCCUAAAGUCCUUUUCUUUUAGCAGAAGACUUGAGUUUGUAAACUCGGCUCAUAUAAUUUCAGCUUGCCUGUCUACCUUCCUUCCAUCUACCUACCUACCUACUUACAUAAGUACCUACUUAUAUAUGGAGAACACGGUGGAAUUUAAUUUUUCUUAUUCUUUUCGACUUUGGUUGGCUUGGUGAAUCAAGUAAACUGUGUUGAAGAAAAACUAACUUUUGAGGGAAAAAAUUGAAAAAAAAUUAUGAUUCUUUUUUUUUUUUUUUUUUUUUUUGAGACGGAGUCUCGCUCUGUCGCCCAGGCUGGAGUGCAGUGGCGCGAUCUCGGCUCACUGCAAGCUCCGCCUCCCGGGUUCACGCCAUUCUCCUGCCUCAGCCUCCCAAGUAGCUGGGACUACAGGCGCGCGCCACUACGCCCGGCUAAUUUUUUGUAUUUUUAGUAGAGACGGGGUUUCACCGUUUUAGCCGGGAUGGUCUCGAUCUCCUGACCUCGUGAUCCGCCCGCCUCGGCCUCCCAAAGUGCUGGGAUUACAGGCGUGAGCCACCGCGCCCGGCCAAAAAUUAUGAUUCUUUGAAAAGGAUUUUUCUCAGGUUAGUUUAUAUAGUUUCACAGAUGCUUGAGAUAAGGAUUAGAAAGUUCAGACACUGAAUCUCCACAGACCCCUGUGAAUGUGUUGGCUAAGCACCUUGUCUUCUCAGGAACACACACUGGAACAGACUUUCUUUCAGUAAAACAGGGCCAGAAUAGUCUUUGAAACAUCCAACGGUGGUUUGGGAAGAGGAUUCUCUAUAUAAUGCCUGUCCAAAUACAGAAUAAAAAUUUUCAACAAUUAGCAAAAAUGUGGAUUUUUCAGUUACCAAUUCCUUAUUUGGCACAGUUGGUCUUUCUCAUCUUAUUCAUUCAUUCAUUUAUUUCAUUUUAUUUAUUUACUUUUAAAAUACUUGUUUAAUUCACCUUUCUUGCUCCCAUUGAGCCUUUUAACUAAUCAAAUGCAUUUGAAAUGCUAUUAAUUUAUGAUAACAGUAAGACCCAAGACAUCACUUUAUGUAAUAUCUUGUAUUGUAGUUCAUUGUUGUCAGCUCUUUUUCUGAUGGGGUUUUGAUUUAGCUGGAGGCAGUUUAAGGGUGUUCAUUCCCCAAUAAUGUUUGUCUGUUGAAGCUGGUGAGCUAGACUAACAGUACAAAGAGUUCCUGUGUACCCUUCACCCAGCUUUCCCUGAUGUUAACAUCUUAUAUAACCAAAGUAUGUUUAAGCAAAGAAAUUAUCAUUGGUGUAACAUGACUAAAGAAGUGAUUAUAUCUUUUAUUGGCAGUUUUCCAGUUUUUCCACUAAUGCCUUUCGUUUUUUUCCUAGAUCUAGUUUAGGAUGCUGCUGUGCAUUUAGUCAUCCUGUCUUCUUUGUCUCCUCCUGACUGUGGCUAUUUCUCAGCCUUUCCCUGUUUUUAGGACCUUGACACUUUUUUAGUGUAACGGUCAGGUAUUUUGAAGAAUGAGUGUCUUGCAACUUGAGUCUGACUGAUGCUUUCUCAUGAUUAAAUUGGGGUUUUAGAUUUCUGGGAAGACCACCACAGAGGUGAAGUACGCUUCUCAUUGCUUCAUAUCACAGCGUACAUGAUGUUAAUGUGAGUUAUUACUGGUGAUGUUAAUUGUGAUAGUGGCCAGUUUUGUUUUAUUUUAUUUUUUAAUAGAAGACCAGUUGUCUGGGACUAUACACACUCCAACACAUUUGCAAAUUGGUGGCAAUGAUUAUUGACUAGUCCUCAAACUACUAACUUCAUGAUAAUGGAAAGCCGAAACUCCCAAAUCACAUGGACCUCAAAGUUCAAUUAGAAAAUUUGGUUAGGACCUGACGACAAUGUUGCGAUUUGCUACAGCCUGCCCUGCAGUCUCAACUCUGGGGUCCCCUCAGUGGUGAGCUCAGUCACAGUGCUGCUUCUGUGUAUACUUACCCAGUAAACAACCCAGGCAUUGGGGCCUGUCUCAGAAACCACAUCUCCAAUAGAAAGGAGAACACUUGGGAAAGCAGGAAGGAGUAAGAAACGGAACUCGCCCAUUCCUGACAACUAAUCCUUUUCCUUUCUAAGUAUGGCUUAGUGGAUGUCAGCCAUUCACUGUUCAGGACAGGAUAGGGAUGAGGAGAGAAUUCUUUUUCAUUUGACAAGGACAUUGAAUUUUCCUUAUCCAUGGAUCAAGACUAGAAGGUAUGGAGAGGAAAAGGGCUUCUCAUCUCUUUCUUUCAGUAGCUUCAUGCACUGAUGCAUCGUACUUACUGAAUGUUUUACCUUCUCUGUGCUCUUCUCAGAGGAUGCACAGAGGAUUGGGAAGAGGAAGUAUUGGUGACUUGAUCUAGAAAAAAGAGAUUGUUUCAAGCCACAAAAAGUUUGAGGGUAAAAUCUCAAGUCCUGUGUGUGAUGAAUCAGUAGAAAAGGUAUCCCAGUGGCCAGUGUGAGUAAGCUGUCAUAUUUUCGGUAGUAAUCCUUGGUCCUGUUUGAUUUUCCUCAUCCUCACAUAUAAGAUGGAGCCAUUUCUCCCUCUGGCGUUUGCCAUCACAGUGUCCUGCAGUCUCUUGGUCUUGAGAUAGAAGGUUGAGAGAAACACUUUGCAGUAUUGGGAGAACUGGGUCUGCCUGUGGGAGUACUUGUAUCUCAAUCAAUAUUACAGAACUUGGCUCCUUGUUUCCAACAAAUGUUUUGCUCUGUUCUCAUCCUGGGAGUUGAAGGUUGAGGCGAGGUGGGAGAUGUGCUGUAUAAUAUGGCAGCCACUAACCACAUGUGGCUGUUGAGCACUUGAAAGGUGGCUAGUGCCACAUGUUGAAAAAUAAUAUUUUGGAUAUAUUUGUAAAAUAAUUUUUUUCAAUGAGCCUUUUGAAAUGUGGCUACUAGAAAAUUUUAAAUGGUGUAUGUGGCUCCUAUGAUAAUUCUAUUGGAUGGUGCUGGCUUAGAGCCUGGGAAGAACAUGGAUCAGAGUCAAUUGACCUUGUGUUCUCCCCUGAGUUCUAAUAAUAUUGUCAUUAAAAGGAGAAGCUUCAACAGCCAUAAUUUUCAUUUUAAAAAGUCUAAUUCAGAAGAAUUGGCUCAUUUUAUAUUAUUGCUUGGACUGGAGAAAAAUCUGACAUUUGGUAUUUUCAUAAUUGAGAACAUAACUUGCUGACUUAAAAAAAAAAUCACAACAUUUUGUGCUUGGCCUUAGGUACCAGCCUUUGAGCUCUUUGAAAAUAGGGAUUGGGUCUUUUUCUCUUUCUACCAUCCUUUUUCCCCCAAAACCACACACUAACACGUAGAAGAUGGUUAACUGGCAUUUGUUGAAAACCAAAAUAACUUUAAAUAGAGAAAACUUUGUGAAGCUACCUUGUAUUUAUGGUUGGAAGAGUGAAAUACCUUUAUAAGGCAUCCCAUUUUCUUAAGAUAGCCAGCAAAAAUGAAGAACAUUGAUCCAAGUGUUUAUUUACUUAUUGAUUUAAUUACCAUUCUCAUCAGGUGUCCCUGUCAUCUCAGCUUAUGAUAAGGAAUCUUUUCAAGAUGCUUCACCUCAUCACUCUCUAGGUAAAGGGGGACAGAAAAGGAUGCUGCUUACAUAUACGAAUCCCCAUCUUUGCUCAGAUAUUAUGUCUAAGGGCCUAAGGACUGGAUAAUCUUAUUUUUUCUGUGGCUUGAUCCUUUCCAACAUUUAAUCUAUGGAGGUUGUGAGGAUAACAAUGAAAAGGCAAGUUUAAGCUUGGACUGUAGAUACUUUUCACUGGGUGGUUUUAUUUUAUUAUGCUUCAUUGUGAACCAGAGCCUCUGUGAACAUAUGACUUAUAGGCCCUCAGGCUUCCACUGUGUCCCUUUCCCUGAUUCGUCCUUCUUCACUGCAUGCCCUGGUGUUGGGUGAGGGAGCAGGCUUUAUGUGAUGUCAUUUUCUCAGAGCCCUGAGCUGGGAAAUUCAAGAGUCUCCAUGAUUCCUAGUUAGGCAUGGAAGAGACCCUAACUGGUCCCUCAGGAACAUGUUUGGUUGGUCAGAGGUAACUCUUAUAGAAUCUAUGAUGGCUUAGUCGUUCACUCUUCCUAGAAAAGACCUCUUUAAAAAGGCCUUUUGGUUAUAUACGGCCUGAGUUUUAAGUAAUAUUUGCAAUGUUGAUUCUCUGGUAGAAGAGAAUGAAAAGUUGUGAGUGCUCUUGGAAGAGUGCCGGACAGCUGUAGUGAUGGGAAAAGUAUUGGCCUUGGAGUCAGACCUGUGUUUACUUCCUGGCUCUGCUAUUUUCUAGUUGUAUGACUCUAUGCAAGUAACUUCUCAUCUCUGAGCAUUAAUUUCUUCACCUGUUUGACAUAGACAAUGUCUGCCUCACAAAGUUGUGAUAUGUUAAUGUAUGUGGGAUACCUAUCUCAGGACCCAAUACUUAGUCUUUAUAAAACACUAAAUGAAUUGGUUUUCUCAUGUAUGUCUUAUGGUUUUGCUGGUGAUGGACCAAUAGUCAUCUUCCAUCUUCACUUUAGAGGUGGGGGAAAAGGGCAUUAGAGUGAUUGUGUGGUAAAAUCCACUCUAAUUCUAGCUGUGAGAAAAAGAGCGGUGAAAAUGUGGUAAGCAAUUGCUUCUAAAAAGCUUGGACUAAAAGCGCUUGAUGGAUUUGUGCUGGCUUCCCGGUAGACUCAUCUCUGUACUGCCCGCACAGCACAAUUAAUUGUUGUUACUAGAGAAGGAACAAAUAAAGAAAAGAGAGAGAGCAGACAUAAAAACAUCCUUUCAUCUUUCUGAAGACAGUCCCCUUUGUCAGAUCAGUGGAGCUGUACCUGUGAAUCACCUUGGGAAAGCACAGUGUGGGUAACUAGAAGGAAGGUCUUGUGGCUCAUUUUGUACCCACUUCCUGGGCUGGGGAAAUAUCUAAACUAACCUUUCUUACUUGUCAAUAUCUACUACCGUUCACCAUGCAUCUUCACAGAUGAGGGCCUCUUUCUCACAUCUUCACUCCAAACACAUUACUGUGUAGACAGCCACUUAUUUUCUGGGAAGAAAACUUUGCAAAGCAGUAGCAGAAUAAAGUCGAGGGUAAACAGAGGCCAUGGAAAAGCACUAGAGUUUGAGUGCAGAGACAUGAGUCUGAGCAUGAGCAGUGAAUAGCUCAUGAAACACUCAAGUUGCAUUCUCCUUAUGUGGAAAUAAAAUAAGUCAUGGUUGUUCUAUGCACGUGGCACCUGACCUUGGGUCCUUAUUGCUAUGCUGCUAGAGUCUAUGAAUCAAGAUUUGCCAGUUGUGAUCUUGAAAUUUAGUCAGAUUAAAAGGGAACUCUGACUUUGAGGGUGAAUGCCCCAAGUGGGCAUCUUAUUCUCCUAUGGAUUCAGCUUGUUAGGCAGAAUGGAAGUGGAGGUCAUAGAUUUUAGGGUUUUCUCCUGGGAUUGAAUCCAGCUGAAGCAGGAAUGAUUCUGGGUGAGCUAUAUAACGUCUCUGAGCAUUAGUUUGUCAUUUUCUUACAUAGGAAUAGAGUUAUUGCCAGAUUUGGAGAUAGUACAUGUUGCAAUGUGGUUGACACAGAAUAAGCUUUCAAUAAAUGAUUGGUAUUGUUGUUGUUGUCGUUAUUAUCUAUAACUACAAUAAUUUCCCUAGCCUUAUUUUAUAGGGAUAGGUUGUGGCAACAUGAAAUGUGACUUGGAAAACUGAUUUGCACUAGAUAGAUAGAAACCAUGUUUUUCUAUCUAUAUAAUGAACAAUGUCAUUUAAGAAAGCUUAGAGGCAAUUCCACCAGCACCAUCUUCUUUUUUAUUUCCAUUCCUAGAUUAUUUGCCCUCAAGUCUUUGGUAAUUUCUUUUUGCCACAUCUCUUGAAUGUUUCUUCUUUACUAUAUUCCAUCUAUUAUUACCAUAAGUCCAACGUUCAUCACCUCCUGCUCCACUGUUGUUCCUGUCUCCUGGCUCUCCUAGAGCCUUGGUUCUCAAAGUGUCAUUCACAGAGCAGCAGCAUCACCCGAAAUGCGUCAUCUCAAGAUCUACCAAGACCUCCUGAAGCAUGAGGCAUGUUCACCCCCGUGUUGUAGGACCUCCAUAUAACUCAUUUAACUACUUCUCCUGCUCAGAGUACAUGCUUGGCCAGUGCGUGUUUGUUCUGCCUCCAGAAUGUUUUCUGACUCUGAUUGCUAUCAUUACUUCUUUUGAAUCUACCUAAAUUCAAGUUACCAUCCAUUGCCAUGACUAUGGCAAUAGUCUCUGAAAUUGUCUUCUACUUUUAUGGUUUCCCCUUGUGGCCUUUUUCCACACCAUCUGGAGAGAUCUAAAAUUGUUGGUCAGAUCAUAUCACACCCCUCCCCUUAAGCCAUACGGUGGCUGCUGUAGUAUCUGCAGAAGGUCCCUGACUUAUGAUGGUUUGACUUACAAUUUGUCCACUUCACACUGAGUUUAUCUGGGUGUAACCAACCCCAUAGAAAUCAAGGAGCAUCUGUAGAAAUGUUUGAAAGGCCCUUUCAUGGCCUGCAAAGCCCUGUGAGAUGACUCUAUGUUCUCUCCUUUUUUUUUCUUUCUUUAUUUUUUUUGAGAUGGAGUCUCGCUCUUGUCUCCCAGGCUGGAGUGCGAUGGUGCGAUCUCGGCUCACUGCAGCCUCCACCUUCUGGGUUCAAGCAAUUCUCCUGCCUCAGCCUCCCGAGUAGCUGGGAUUACAGGCACCAGCCAUCACGCUCGGCUAAUUUUUGUAUUUUUAGUAGAGAUGGGUUUUCACCAUGUUGGCCAGGCUGGUCUCGAACUCCUGACCUCAGGUGAUCCACCCGCCUCGGCCUCCCAAAGUGCUGGAAUUACAGGUGUGAGCCACUGCGCCUGGCCUCUCUGCUUUUUUCAUACCACUCAUCACUUUACACAGUAAUCUGUAGACACACUGACCUUCCUUUAGCCCUCUGUAUAAGCCAAGCUUUUUCCCACUUGAUCUUUCUCUGAUUCUGUGCAAAACUGGCUUGGAAGUAUCUUUCAAGGCUUAGCUCAAAUGUUAAAGCCUUACCUAGCUCUUCCCCAUUCUUUAGCUAAAGUAGCACACAUACCCCCCUCCCCAUCAUUCUUCUGUCAUUAUCUUGCUUUAUAGUCUACAAAGCAUGUAUGGUUCUCUAAAAGAGUGAUUACCAUGCUUUUGUUUUCUUUAUGUACAUUGCAAACUGUUUUGGUGAGAAAUAUUUUAGUAAUAAUAAUAAUGGUGAAGAUUUAGUGAGUGUUUGCUAUAGGCUAGGCACACUGUAUGGUAAAUUAAAUAAUUUAAUAGAUCAUUUAUUUGGAUUAUUUCAUUCUAUUUAGCUGAUUAUAUAUUUAUAUUUUUUGUGUUCCUCUUGUUUUAGGAUAUCAGCUUCUUGAGAGCAGGGUCCAUGUUUGUUGCAUCUGUAUCUCCGCCUGUAGAAGAUUCUCUGGCAUAGGGAUUUUUGUGCAGGAAGUGUUUAUUCAGGAACUGAAUGGAUCUCAGAAGAUUAUCAUUUGGGAAUAGAUCUACAUGACAAGAAAGAACAAAGAGUCUCUCUCAUUCUUUUUCCCAGAUAUAUCCCGGGAGAAAAUACCCUCGACUUUUUCUUAUCUUUAAUCUGAGAAGGAAGCAGUUGUUGGAAUCUGAUUUAGGAUUGGCUCUAGUGGCCCUGUGUGCAGACACAGAUCUUGGGAUUCAUCUGACCAUUUGGGGAGAGAGGUUCUUGAGGGGCACCUUGAUGAUAACGAGUCUUUCUAAAGCUUUAAGUUUGGCGUUUGAGGUGGUUGGAAAUACCAGGUCUUCCGACUUUUACGUUCUUUGUGCGCACGCUGGUGAUGUGCGUAUGUGAACCUUUAUUAUUAUGGACUCAGCCAGCAGUAACCAUGAUUCCAACAAUGUCUCACCCAUCUUGGCUGCCACCCAAAAGCACUGGUGAGCCCCUCGGCCAUGUGCCUGCACGGAUGGAGACCACCCAUUCCUUUGGGAACCCCAGCAUUUCAGUGUCUACACAACAGCCACCCAAAAAGUUUGCCCCGGUAGUUGCUCCAAAACCUAAGUACAACCCAUACAAACAACCUGGAGGUGAGGGUGAUUUUCUUCCACCCCCACCUCCACCUCUAGAUGAUUCCAGUGCCCUUCCAUCUAUCUCUGGAAACUUUCCUCCUCCACCACCUCUUGAUGAAGAGGCUUUCAAAGUACAGGGGAAUCCCGGAGGCAAGACACUUGAGGAGAGGCGCUCCAGCCUGGACGCUGAGAUUGACUCCUUGACCAGCAUCUUGGCUGACCUUGAGUGCAGCUCCCCCUAUAAGCCUCGGCCUCCACAGAGCUCCACUGGUUCAACAGCCUCUCCUCCAGUUUCGACCCCAGUCACAGGACACAAGAGAAUGGUCAUCCCGAACCAACCCCCUCUAACAGCAACCAAGAAGUCUACAUUGAAACCACAGCCUGCACCCCAGGCUGGACCCAUCCCUGUGGCUCCAAUCGGAACACUCAAACCCCAGCCUCAGCCAGUCCCAGCCUCCUACACCACGGCCUCCACUUCUUCAAGGCCUACCUUUAAUGUGCAGGUGAAGUCAGCCCAGCCCAGCCCUCAUUAUAUGGCUGCCCCUUCAUCAGGACAAAUUUAUGGCUCAGGGCCCCAGGGCUAUAACACUCAGCCAGUUCCUGUCUCUGGGCAGUGUCCACCUCCUUCAACACGGGGAGGCAUGGAUUAUGCCUACAUUCCACCACCAGGACUUCAGCCGGAGCCUGGGUAUGGGUAUGCCCCCAACCAGGGACGCUAUUAUGAAGGCUACUAUGCAGCAGGGCCAGGCUAUGGGGGCAGAAAUGACUCUGACCCUACCUAUGGUCAACAAGGUCACCCAAAUACCUGGAAACGGGAACCAGGGUACACUCCUCCUGGAGCAGGGAACCAGAACCCUCCUGGGAUGUAUCCAGUCACUGGUCCCAAGAAGACCUAUAUCACAGAUCCUGUUUCAGCCCCCUGUGCGCCACCAUUGCAGCCAAAGGGUGGCCAUUCAGGGCAACUGGGGCCUUCGUCAGUUGCCCCUUCAUUCCGCCCAGAGGAUGAGCUUGAGCACCUGACCAAAAAGAUGCUGUAUGACAUGGAAAAUCCACCUGCUGACGAAUACUUUGGCCGCUGUGCUCGCUGUGGAGAAAACGUAGUUGGGGAAGGUACAGGAUGCACUGCCAUGGAUCAGGUCUUCCACGUGGAUUGUUUUACCUGCAUCAUCUGCAACAACAAGCUCCGAGGGCAGCCAUUCUAUGCUGUGGAAAAGAAAGCAUACUGCGAGCCCUGCUACAUUAAUACUCUGGAGCAGUGCAAUGUGUGUUCCAAGCCCAUCAUGGAGCGGAUUCUCCGAGCCACCGGGAAGGCCUAUCAUCCUCACUGUUUCACCUGCGUGAUGUGCCACCGCAGCCUGGAUGGGAUCCCAUUCACUGUGGAUGCUGGCGGGCUCAUUCACUGCAUUGAGGACUUCCACAAGAAAUUUGCCCCGCGAUGUUCUGUGUGCAAGGAGCCUAUUAUGCCAGCCCCGGGCCAGGAGGAGACUGUCCGUAUUGUGGCUUUGGAUCGAGAUUUCCAUGUUCACUGCUACCGAUGCGAGGAUUGCGGUGGUCUCCUGUCUGAAGGAGAUAACCAAGGCUGCUACCCCUUGGAUGGGCACAUCCUCUGCAAGACCUGCAACUCUGCCCGCAUCAGGGUGUUGACCGCCAAGGCGAGCACUGACCUUUAGAUUCAGUCACCUGUUCAGCCGGCACUGAGAAGAACGAACACAAGAAAAAGAUAAGAAAUACUAGAGUAAAGGCCAUCAAACUACGCGAUAGUCUCUGUUCUUCAUCUGCUAUUAACCUUGCCUUAGAAACACAUAAAUUAUGAGAUUUUUUUUAAAAGUUGUUACCAAAUACACAUUUCACAUUGAAUCAUGUAGGAUCUUGAUGGGCCUUUGUUCCCAAGGACUUCCACAUUUUUGCACAGAUUAUGCUCCAUCCCAUUCACUUCUGCAUUCCUGUAACUUUUAAUCCCUAUGUUUGUCUCACUUUUCAUCUGGUUGAAUGGCUUUUCUUAGUGUGGUAUUUGCUGUCACAUAGUUUUUCCUGGGUGAGUCUGCCAACUCACAGGUGCUUUUAGGCUUGAAAUCUCCAUCCUAUCAUUUCCGUUUUGCCUGUGACUGUAAAGAGUAGCCAUUCUUUUCCCAUGUAUUGAAGAGGAUAUUCUUCUCUUGCUUUAUACUACUCACGUCCUUGGGGAGGGAAAUGCACAAUUUUUUUUUGUUAGGCUGUAAAGAAUUUAAGCUGUAAAUUACAUAAGUUAGAACAAGCCCAAAUUUAAUUUGCAACCAUCAGAAUUCAGAAUCUAUAGUGACCAGUGAUCAAGGCUAAUUGGAAAAGAGUUAUCGGCCCAUAGCUAAUAAGUAGUGACAGACAACCAAGCUUCAAUAUUUUUCUAAAGAAAUUACAGGUGGGAUAUGCUAGAAAAGGCAUUUUGGGGUUAUGUUUAAAAAAACAUUAUUGUCCCACAAUAUUACCUUAAGAUUUUUCUUUUCCGCACUACCUGAACAUUGUAAUACAGACAAACUUGAUUUCUUCUAGAAGAUAACAUUUUCAAUACUGUCCCACUUCUCAUCUUAAAAAUAUUGUCAUGUUUAUUCUAAUAUCCAACACAACUAUCAAAAUUGCCUUUUUCUCUAGAGGAUGAAGGCUGUGAAAAAACCGUUCAAAUUCUCUUCUUUUUCUUUUUUAUUACCAGGUCCAUUUUGCCUGACAAUUGCAAAUCAGAGCAUACAAAAUAAAACUGUGCAGUUUUGUUUGGUUUACUUUCAAAAGAGUAGAAAGCUUGAAAAGAUUCUGAAACCACAGUUUCAUUAUUCUCAUAAUCCUUCUGCAACUGAAAUUACAUAUUGCAGGAGACAUUUUCAUAUCAUCAAUGUGACAUUUACACCACACUUUCAAAGACAAUCACUGAAACAAAAAUUGUCUUUAUGAGCUAAAAAUAUGCAGAAUCUCUGCCUAGAAUCUUUAUUCAAACUUUUAUUAGCCAGUGAAACACUUGCUUGCCAACUGCCAAGCCAUACUUAUUAAGUUCGAACAUGUUUCACUUAAGGAGAGACACCUAGCUUAGUCAUGGCAAGUUGCCAUUUUGUAAACUAAGGAUUUUGGACUGAGAUUUCUUAAAUCUUUCUUCAAAUCUCCCACAAGUAUAUACUUUUAAAUUAUGGAGUAUUUUAAGUCUACAAAAAGGUAUAAAUAAUAAUAUAAUGAAUUCCUAUAUACCUAAUACCCAGUUUAAGACACCAAAUAUAACAAGUAUAAUUACAUCCUCCAAUGUACCGUUUCCUUAUUCCACAGAUAUCUUUUUCAUUAUUGUGAAGUGAUGUUCAGAUUUCUAGUUUUUUUUCUAGUUUUUAAUUUUAACAUCAGAACUGAAAUAAAAAAUUAUGGAUACGUGUUUUGAAUUGCAAACUAUUCCUCAGGAAUUCCAAUUAAAUUUAUUUUACUUGAAUAGGAAUGAUCAUAAAAGUGAUUCUUUUUUUGUGACUAGAAAUUCUUAAGCCGAUGGUCACUAUAGCUCAUCCUUAAUGUAUGGCUCAUUUGCUUUUGUCACUAAACGGUUUUGUGUUAGAACCACCAAAAUUAUAGCUUUUAAGAGCUUCCUUUGACCACUGUCUUUUUCUUACCCUAGUUCUCUUAUCUUUGAUCGUAUAUUUCUCAUAAUGUGAAAUAUGAUGAGAUUCACUUAGGGGCAGCAUGUUAGUUUUGGGAGGCAAUGUCAACUGUGUCUCUGAAUUCCUGUCUUCCAAAUUGAAGCCAGACCAUGCUGAUGACCUCAAGUAGCACUGACUAUUUGACAAUAGGGCUGAUAAUGUAAUCGGCUUGAAUUUUGACUUAGUAACUUUUUAUGUAAUACUUUCGGAGAAAUUCUCUUUAGGACAAAGCAGAGAGUCCAAUUUAUUGAGGGAUAGAUUGUAUCUCUUAAAGUGGUCAUAUUAUUAUUAAUUUUGCCAAAAGAAGAAGAAUUUAUUGAAUAUUUAUACUAUAAAAUGCAGUAACAUUCUACUUGCUUAUUACAUUUAAAUCCUUGUGUAACUGAAUGUUUACAUGUCAAGAGGAAAAGCUGUAAGAAAAUGCUGUCACAGACCCAUCCCUGUGGCAUCGUCAGCAGAAUACUGCUUGCUUACAAUCUUUAUUAUGCAUUCUUAUAACAUAACCUCAGAGUAUCUUUACCAAAGGUUUUUAAAGUAAAUCUCUUUUUAAGAUAGACUUAUUCUUUUAUAAUAAUGAAUGUGCACUCAUACAUAUGUAGAAACAUUUAGAUUUAGAGUUUUUUUUUUCUUUCACAAGGUAUAAUAAGGAAAGGAUCCUACAAUAUUUUAUUCUAGGGUUUCUUAAAUAUAUGAUUUAUAUUACUGUCUUUUCUAUUAAUCAUUUGAUUUAAACAAUGCCAAGUCACUCUUUUUUAGUUGCAUGAAAUUUUGCCUGCAACAGAGAGAAAAAGAUUGUAUUACUUUAAUGAUUAUAAUCAUACUGUCUGCUGAUAUAAUAUCAUAAUUGUUGUGGUUUAAAUACAUAAAUAGUAGAAAAAUCAGAGUCUAUAACAGAAAGUUUGUAAAAAUAUACUGAUUUUGAAAAGUAUCAGGAAUAUAAAUAUUUGGUAAUUCUGUGUAACAAGAGAGACAUGGAAAAGGAAAAAAAUCCACUAUAUCAUGGGCUCUGCAGAACAUAUCAAAAUAGGAUUUCUUAAAUUUUUCAACCCCCAGACCAUACUGACUCAACAUGGAGUCUCACUGGCCAAGAAAAUUGCCUUUAAAACUCGAAAAUAAGGCCAGGUGUGGUGACUCACACUUGUAAUCCCAGCAAUUUGGGAGGCUGAGACAGGAGGAUUGCCUGAGGCCAGGAGUUUGACACCAGCCUGGGCAACAUAGUGAGACCUUGUCUCUACAAAAAAUAAAAUAAAAUAAAAACCAAAUUAGCCAGACAUGGUGGCAUGCGCUUGUUUAAAAAAACAAAUAAAUAAAUAAUCGACUCAAAAAUAAGUCAUGUGUCCCAGCAUAAGGCAUCAGGUUGUUAGAUGCUGGCAUCUCUGCAGCUCAAAGAUGUGGGUUCUUUUUCUUGUCAUUAACACAUUGUUAUUUCUGUAGGAGCAACUUCUCUGAUCAAAAUUACUUUUCUGGGUAUGUGCUGAUUAAGGGGGUGGACUUAUCAACACUAUAAUUGUUCCCUAUGAAAGAUUCCACAGAGAUGUUUAUGGUGAGGUUUAAAGGAUAUGAAACUCUACAUUUAAACAAGUAUUUUAUAUUUGGGUACAGAGGAAGAAAGAGAGGGCUUUUUCCAUGGGGCUAUAGUAGAGAGUUAGUGGAAUAUAGACAGGACUCUGAAAACACAACUUCCAGCCAUUUUUUUAGUUAGUAAAAAUCCUAUUAAUGUGAACCAGCCAGGAAUAACAGUGUUAUUUCUAUUGGAUAUGGUUUGGGCUUCUCUUGUCAAAUCUGUGUCGGCUGCCCCCUGAUCCUUCCAUUAUCAAGUUUUGAAGGGUGUUGGGGAAAUUAUGGCAGCUGCUAGGGAGAUCAGGGAAACACUGAUGUAACCUCAAAGCCUCUCACCAUUCCUCUUGGCUUGGAAAGGCUUUAUUUUUUCAUAUACAUUUCUAGAAAUAUUGCUAUUCUACCUUAGUAUUUCACAUUUGUAGUUCAAACAAGCGAUUGUCCAUCUGUUGCCUAGAGCUAUAGUACAUGUGUGUUAUGAAUGAAAUAUGACAGCAUGUUCCAUACCCCUGCUUUAGCCAUCUGUGGGAAACCAGCAAACUGAAAAAGACACCUCUGCAAAAUGUGCCUCAAGUCCAUUUCUUGGGAUCGCUCGUUUGGUGCACUCUCGUGGGAGACAAUCAGAGAACAACAUAUACUUGUGCCUUAUUUUCAAAGAAUCUAUUUACACUACUAUGAAUAUUCCACUGAAGAGUCAAUGAUGUAAAUGAUAACCACCAAAUCUCAAAAAUAUACUCACCAAAAAGUAAAAAAGUAAAAAAAAAAAAAAAAGAAAGAAAGAAAAGAAAGAGAGAGAAGUCAACUUUUCAUCUUAAUAUAUUCUAGUAGUAUUUAUUUUUUCCUUGUCUUGGAAGUAUCUCAUAGGUCUUUAAAUGAGUAAAACAUUUUUAUGCCAGAAGGUGAUAUAAUGGAUGUUAGUGUUUUUUAUUUGAUUUUACAGUAGUUUUAGUCAGAUAAUGAGGACAGAGACUUCAACUUGAUUCUUUACCACCAUUCAGCAUAUUUUUUAAUUGUCUUCAUUGUAUUUGCUUAAUAGUGGUCCAGACAAGUUCAAAACUUGUUCUCAGUGAGGCAUUAAUAUGGUGCAACCAUGAAUAUUUCAGGCCAAGUUAUUCACUUGACAGAUAACUAGAAUGAAACUUUUCUCAUGAGGCUGUUGUUUGGUUAGCAUAGCCUUAUUUCAAACCUUAAAAAGUUACCUGACUGAAGCUACUAUGACUUGGUAAGGAUUCUUCCUCUCUUGCUUUCUUCCUCCCUUCCUUUCUUCCUCUUCCUUCCUCCUCUUCUUAUUUUCUUUCCUACUUUCCAUCCUACCUAUUAGUGUUGCUGUACUUGGAUUUUUUGUAAAUUAAAUCAAUGCAUUAUGAUUUUAGGGAAUUAUGAUUAUAUUCAUAAGGGGAAGGCUACCAGAAAAUAUAUGUGGCAUCCAUAAAAUCUUCUUUUAUAGGGGCAUAUUUUUUAGGUUGUAUUUAUUCGUAAAGUGAAAUGAGAUAAUAGAGUCUUUCUGUUUCAUGUUAAUGAAUUUUCAUCAGGGACUGAGGUCAUAGAUUCUUGGAAAAUUCAUUUGUGACUGAUCUAGUUUUCUCAGCUGUAUGCAAAGUAAUCUUUCAAAGACUAGGUUAAGAUUUUUUUUUUAAGUCUGAAGCAAUGUAACCCCAAAAAAUUAUAAUUUUAAUGAUGGCAUUUUAUUUUAUUCCAUUGCAGCUUGAUAACUUUCCUUAUAGCAAAGGAAUAACUAUUGUAUUUUCAGAAUUUUAACACAGAUUAACACUUAGCCUGUAAGACUAAUAAUAUAUUGUAAUAGUUGAUACUAAAAUAUUUUUCAGCAGGUUGGACAGCACCAGUUUUUCUUAGAUCACAGACUACAGGCAGAAUUUCCCUUCAAUCCAGAAAAAAGGACACUAAUUUCCUUUUCUAUUUAAUUUUCCUGGCCCUUGUGCAAAAAAUUGUGGACUCUAUCUUAGUUACAACAUGCAUGUCCCUUAUUUUGUGGAGAGCUGUGUGAAAGAUGCGUUUUUUUUCUUUUUUUCUUUUUUUUUUUUUUGAGACGGAGUCUGGCUCUGUCACCCAGGCUGGAGUGCAAUGGCACGAUCUCCUCUCACUGCAAGCUCCGCCUCCCAGGUUCACGCCAUUCUCCUGUCUCAGCCUCCCGAGUAGCUGGGACUACAGGCGCCUGCCACCACGCCCGGCUAAUUUUUUUGUAUUUUUAGUAGAGAUGGAGUUUCACAGUGUUAGCCAGGAUGGCCUCGAUCUCCUGACCUCGUGAUCCACCCGCCUCGGCCUCCCAAAGUGCUGGGAUUACAGGCGUGAGCCACCGUGCCCCGCGUGUUUUUUUCUUUAGCUGAUUGACAGGUCCCCUUCAAAGUUACAAAAAAAAGUGCUAAUUUUUGCUGUUAAAUUCUGGUUGUUAUUUAAUUGACAGAAGUCUCUUGAUGCACGAAUAAAUAUCUCUACAUCUAGCCUUUGUUAAAAAUAAAAAUUAAUAUUCUACAAACACCUACAUAUACUAGAGAGGGGUGAAACACUGCAGCUAAUUCCUUUAUAAUACUUUCAGAUGAUUGCAUUAAGCCUUUCAUGUUAUGUGGCAUUGUUAAUUUUUCCUAGAUACCCAUCCACUUAAGGGCCAGAGAAAUCCUUAUUCAUUUAACUCUGGUGGGCAUUUAUGUAACAUACCCAAAUAAAAACGUUAUUAAACAGCCACAAUCGCAUUCAGUCAACUUGGCACUGAAUGUAGCUUCUAAAAUCAGUUCUCUACCCUACGAAUGGAAUGUUCUACCAAGAAAGAGAAGCAUCACCAUGUCAUCUUGUGUUCUACACCACUAUAGAGAGUUACAGUUGCCCCCAAACACGAAUGCUAUUCCCAAAUAAAAUAGAAUCAUGCUUUGGGAGGCCAAGGCGGGCCGAUCACGAGGUCAGGAGAUCGAGACCAUCCUGGCUAACACGGUGAAACCCCGUCUCUACUAAAAAAAAAAAAAAAUACAAAAAAUUAGCCUGGCUCAGUGGCGGGCGCCUGUAGUCCCAGCUACUCAGGAGGCUGAGGCAGGAGAAUGGCGUGAACCCGGGAAGCGGAGCUUUCAGUGAGCCGAGAUAGCGCCACUGCAGUCCGGCCUGGGCGAAAGAGCGAGACUCCGUCUCAAAAAAAAAAAAAAAAAAAUAGGAUCAUGGCCCUUUUAAAGAUCUGAAUCUUCUCUGUUAUUUUCCUGAUGAAUCACCAUCCCAUAUCUUCUUAGUCCUGGCCAGUAUGUAGUUGCGCUCACAUACGUCUAUUCUAGCUCUGUAGCUCCACAAAACAAGUCUUAAGUCCAAAUCUUUGCCUCUUCAUGUCUGAUAUCACCAACUCAUUCAGCUUUUCUUCACUUAUUGACAUAGUGUCAUGUCCUAUCACUCUCUGCUGCUUCUUUAAACAGUGGACACAAACAUAUUUUCUAAUUUUCAGUGUACUCAGUGAAACUUGGCAGUUCACCAUGAGUCAGGCUAGGUUGAAAGGCUUUCUUUAGGGUUGAAAGUAAACGAAAUUGGAAUCACCCAAAGAGAAUUUCCCCAAAAAACCUCAGACCCAGAAGUGUAAAAGCUACAGAAGGAUAGAACUCCCAUGUCUACAGACAGUUCUGUUACUUUUUGUUCUGUACUAUUUUGGAUGUUGCCAAAAUCAAAUUCAUCCUGAAAACAGGAAGCAAGCUAAUGCAUAUGCCAUCCAUGAGAUUCCCACUUCUGGGUCAGUUCAUAUUCCAUUCAACCUUUUCCUUUUAUCCUUGUCUUCUUCAGAAUAAGACAUUUUUCCUCCAUAUUUUCAUAUUAAAUAUUAACACUUUAUAGGUUCUACUUUAAUAUAUGGACACUUUACAGGUUAUACAUAAAUAUUUGCUGGUUGAUUGAUUUCGAGAUUCAUUCAUUCUGUGCUCAAAUAUUUGUACCUAGAGACGUUACAUGUUAGAAAAAGUGAGCAGCUUCUUUCUCUAAUCAUUUAGGAGUCCAUAUUUUUCUUUUCUUUUUGUUCUCCCAACAUCCUUAUCUCUUACUCAGCUCUUCAAUUUAUAAUUACCAAAUAAUCACUGUUAGAGAAUCAGCCCCUAAGUAACUUUGAUUCUGGCCAACUGUAAUAAGAUCCAACCACUUAAAUCUGUACUUACUCAAUAGGAAGGAAUGUGACAUCAGGAAGAGUCAUUCCAGUGACAUUAGUAAGACUUUAUGGAGUACAUAAAAUUUGAUAAGAAAUCUUGAGCUGAUUCUUUGACUUGAUUUAGAAGUUGAGAAAAGAGUAUUUAAGGCACAACAGGGAAACAUGGGCUAUACUCAGAGAAGACCCUCUGCAUUGGCCAAAAUAUCAUGGAUUCUGGAAAUUCCUUCUUAACAGAAAAAAAAGGCUUCCAAAUAAUCAGGCUGAAUGGGAAGAAAAAGGCAUAGAGGAAGCCUGAGGAAGUAUUUACUUGCUUUUCCCAUCUCUUUAUAAUUGGAAGAGAAGAUGAUCUGCCAAAAUAUAACCCAGCAUGCACAGUAUGGACAGGAAGCAGCCCUCCAUGAACUUUAUUAUCACAGAAUAUGAGCAUUCUUAUUGAUCCACAGCUACAUCUUCUAUUCUUGCAGCAAGGGUACAUGUCCUUUGACCCUCCACAAAAGAACAAGCAGGACAUCUCUAUUUUCCUAUUGAGUCUGAGUCCAUUAUUAGAAAGGACUUCCCAGCCAUCUUUUCUACUUGGUAUUAAAAUUCCCUUACAGAUUCAUUGCUAAGUGCCAAUUCUUUUUUUUUCUUUUGAGACGGAGUCUUGCUCUGUCGCCCAGGCUGGAGUGCAGUGGCGCAAUCUCGGCUCACUGCAAGCUCCGCUUCUCGGGUUCACGCCAUUCUCCUGCCUCAGCCUCCCGAGUAGCUGGGACUACAGACGCCCGCCACCGCGCCCAGCUAAUUUUUUUUGUACUUUUAGUAGAGACGGGGUUUCACCGUGGUCUCGAUCUCCUGACCUCGUGAUCCGCCCGCCUCGGCCUCCCAAAGUGCCAAUUCUGACUCUACUUAAACAUCACCUGUAUCAGGGAGCUCAUUAUUCCUUGAGGUCUUACAUUUCUUUCAGCACAUUUUGUUCCAAGCUACACGACUUUAAAACAGAGCCAGCCUUUGGGGCAUAUGUUCUCUUUGGUGCCACACAAAACCUGUAGUACAUGAUACAGUGUUGCUUCCCCCCUCCUUUUCCUUCCAUAUAUAUUUGUUUUGUUUUGGGCAUUGCAUUACUUUUUUGAAUUUUUAAGAAUCUCUAAAAUUAGUCUGAAGGAUGUUCUGAGGGCCAGACAUUAGAAUUUGUGAGUUUUUUUGUUGCUGGUUGUACUUUCCUAUUUAGAAGACAGACCGUUCUGACAGUUGUUGUGUAGCUUCAUGCCUUCCCCAGUAACUAACCCAUGAACAGUACACCCCUUUUAUCUGACUUGUUGAUAAUGACCUUAAAAAUGUUAGGAAAUGGGCCGGGCGCGGUGGCUCGUGCCUGUAAUCCAGCACUUUGGGAGGCCGAGGCGAGCGGAUCAUGAGGUCAAGAGAUCGAGACCAUCCUGGUCAACAUGGUGAAACCCCGACUCUACUAAAAAAAAUACAAAAAUUAGCCGGGCGUGUUGGCGGGCGCCUGUAGUCCCAACUACUUGGGAGGCUGAGGCAGGAGAAUCACCUGAACCCAGGAGGCAGAGGUUGCAGUGAGCAGAGAUUGCGCCACUGCACUCCAGCCUGGGCGACAGAACGAGACUCCGUCUCAAAAAAAAAAAAAAAAAAAAAAGGUUGGGAAAUAUUGGUGUAUAAUCCCCAUGUCUAACAAGGAAGAAGUCAAAAGCAAAAGAUAGUGGUAUUGCCGAAAACUCAUUAUUUCUAGUUAGUUCAUCUGUGGAAAAGGAUAUCGUUCUUGAGGAGAGGGGUUCUAUUAUGCUAUAGUUUUCUAUGGAAAUGUACAAAUGCUUUCCUCAUUGCUCUGGAUGACUAUUUAGUUUAAAUAAUAUACCUUUGUCAUGGGGAAGACCAUGAUUGUGGCUUCUUCUACCCCAACUUUGAAUGAGAGAGCACUGUAAGCAGAAACUGCCAUCAGUCUCCUGGGCAGGACCUGGAGGUAACUUUCUGAGCUGUAAAAUAGUAAUUCCUAAGAGAGCUUACAAACUGCUUCCACACAGAAAAUAGCGCAGGGAGGACAGUUAUUAGUACCCCUAUUCUAGAAGAGAAAGCUGAGGCUCAAGCCAUUAAGUGACUUGCCAAAAGCUGUGACAUAGCUGGGAAGUGGCAGAUUUGGGGAUAUAACCAGGUCUUGCAAGUCCAGUGCUGUCUCCAAGUAGCCACGCUCACAGCUGAGAACACCUUAGAGGACAAUAUCGACUUCUUACAGACUACCAAGCCCCCAGUCAUCCAGGGAAAUUCAGAGACCAAUUGACUGCCAGGUGGCAAAUCCACAUGUGUACUGCGGUCUUUAGAGAUCAUUUAGAGCUUGCACACAUCUGUGUCUUCUUGUGGGAAACCUCUAGGUAUUCUGUCUGAUCAGCACUGUGAGGAAGUUGGUGGGAAAAGGCCACUGAUAAGAACAAACAAUGGGCAGAAGGAAGCACAUUGCAAUAAAUUUCCCCAGAGAGAGUUCCUUUACAUUCCAUUCACCAAAAACCUCUCUGGAACUGUCAGGUUCAGAAUAUCAACCAAGACCAUAUCAUUUAGAAUUCAUUGGCAUGUAGAGGUGACUCGAUUCCUAAAAGAAGCCUCUCUCCCAUGAACCACGAUGUACGUUCCACAGAGGCAGAAACCGCCGUAGGUUAGCAAUGCAUUUUAGUCUUUCUCUCCAUUCACAUUUACUGAGAGCACACCACGUGCAUGUUGCUGCAACAGGCAUUUCCGAUAGAGCCGAUCCAUGAGCUAACAAUGUCUGAAAACAAAUGUUAUGGAACUGUUGGCAUUUCUGAGAUUUGGCCUUUGCCAUUUGAUAGACUUUGCUUCCCAGGAUGCUGUCAUUUUGUGAUUUUUUAUAAUUACAAGGAAUUUGGUACCAUGUUGUUUUCAAAAAACCUCCUAGAAAGUCUCCAUGUAUGCUCUAGAAGUUGCUCUACGUAACAGUUCAGCAAGCAAGUGUUCCUUCUCUUGAGCUGCGUCCCUCAGGAAGCUGUACCUUUAGGGUGUGCUUUCCACUUUUUAUUUCCUCUCAUUUCACUCCUUUCAUUGUUUGCUAUAUCCUAAAAUAUGUGAAGUGAGAGAAAAAAUAUCAUUUCUUCUCAUUAAAUCUCCUGCAUUAAAUCUAAGAAUCCUUUAAAAUAAUCACACCUGAUAAGUGUUUUAUGCAUUUCCCUCCCUGGAGUGUUAUCAUCCAUCAAGCCAGUAUCAUCAUCCACCUGCUUAUUCCUUGGGACUAAUGAGAGCCAAGUUAAAUAGCAAAUGACUUCUCACCCCUUCCUAGUCCUCAUGCCUGAGGAAUAAGGGCGACAUUAAUGGGAGCGGGAGAGUGGUGGCUUUGGUUGAGAUGCACGUUCACAGACUAGAAAAGUGCCUCACCUCCAUGGUGUAUAUGUGCCACCUUUUCUUAAUCCAGUCUAUCAUUGUUGGACAUUUGGGUUGGUUCCAAGUCUUUGCUAUUGUGAAUAGUGCCGCAAUAAACAUAAGUGUGCAUGUGUCUUUAUAGCAGCAUGAUUUAUAAUCCUUUGGGUAUAUACCCAGUAAUGGGAUGGCUGGGUCAAAUGGUAUUUCUAGUUCUAGAUCCCUGAGGAAUCUCCACACUGACUUCCACAAUGGUUGAACUAGUUCACAGUCCCACCAACAGUGUAAAAGUGUUCUUAUUUCUCCACAUCCUCUCCAGCACCUGUUGUUUCCUGACUUUUUAAUGAUUGCCAUUCUAACUGGUGUGAGAUGGUAUCUCAUAGUGGUUUUGAUUUGCAUUUCUCUGAUGGCCAGUGAUGGUGAGCAUUUUUUCAUGUGUUUCUUGGCUGCAUAAAUGUCUUCUUUUGAGAAGUGUCUGUUCAAUACUAUGCAGCCAUAAAAAAUGAUGAGUUCAUGUCCUUUGUAGGGACAUGGAUGAAAUUGGAAAUCAUCAUUCUCAGUAAACUAUCUCAAGGACAAAAAACCAAACACCACAUGUUCUCACUCACAGGUGGGAAUUGAACAAUGAGAACACAUGGACACAGGAAGGGGAACAUCACACUCUGGGGACUGUUGUGGGGUGGAGGGAGGAGGGAGGGAUAGCAUUAGGAGAUAUACCUAAUGCUAAAUGACGAGUUAAUGGGUGCAGCACACCAGCAUGGCACAUGUAUACAUAUGUAACUAACCUGCACAUUGUGCACAUGUACCCUAAAACUUAAAGUAUAAUAAUAAUGAAAUAAAAUUAAAAAAAAAAAAGAAAAGUGCCUCACCUCCCUGUGAGGCUUGAUGAAUAUUGUGGCCAGUGAGUGGAAAAUGAUUCUUGUCGAAUAGACAGAGUAUUCCCACCCCAGGAAUGGAUUAAUAGAAGACACAAUUUGAGCACUUCUCAGAAUUAUCUAGUAUGCCUGAGUAGAGACUCACAUGGGUGGAAUCUGUGUUGUCUCAUCAGAGGGAAUAAAAAGACAAUGAGGUGGUAAAUGUGAAAAAAGCAGCCUUUUAGAAAAACAUUAUUUUCAAAUACCUUUAUAAAUCAUCUAAUUUAUCUUCACAUAAUAUAAAGAAAAAACUAAUAAAAAUUUUCGUAUUUCACUUUACAUAAUAUGUUCUCCCAUAUUUAGGGAUCAUACAAUUGUAUUGUCUUCAAAACACACACACACACACAUACACACACACACACACACACACACACACCCCUUCCAAGAAAGCUGAUCCUUCAGAAAAUAAAUCUUAUUUUUAAGCACUUGGGUUUUCAGGCCAGAAAAUUAAUAAAUCCUAAACCUGACCCAUUUUUGUAACAGCUAAAAAGGAGAAGAAAAAGCUAGUUAAAUUUUGUGUGGAUCCAUUUAUCUCUUAAAAUAUGCCAAAGCAAUUUGAGGUGGGGGUGGAAACAGGUAUUUAUCUCUCAUGCGUGAUUCUCUCUUUAUAUUUCUAUCUGUUGGGAAAAGGGUAAAGAACUAUUCUUGGUCAUUAUUGAUGUAUUGUGUUGCCACUUUGUAUGGUGCCUGCUGUGCUUUAUCCCGAGGCAUAGCAGUAAUCGUUACUAUCUUGACUCUUUCCUUCAUCACAAGAGAGUAAAUAUGAAGUCUGAAUGUCGUUCCUCACCCCCAAAUUGUUUAACUCUGCUUCCAAACUAGUUUAAGAAAUGCAAAAUGGGAAGAGCUAGCUUUUCUUAGAUACAUUUCUUCCUUUUUUAUUCUUUCUUGGGAGACGUUAAGUAUAAAAGGGAAAAAGUCAGUUCCUUCUUCUCUCUCUUUCUCUUUGGGUGACAGCAAUGCUCACUUAGUAAUUAUAAACUGGAAAUAGGAGAGUAGCUUGAGCAGGUUAUGAUAUAUCUGCCCAAUGUGUUUCAUUCCUUCAAACAUAAACUUUGAGAGUAAAAGAGAUUUUUAUAAUUUAAAUGCCAACGACAGGAAUGGCCUCAUGUUUUAACUUUCAAAUAAUAAAUGGGGAGUUGGUAUUUGGGCAGAGUUUGCAUUUUACUAAUCCUAUAUACUUUGAGCUUAGUUUUUAGAAUUGUGUCAAAUACAUCAACAUAUCAGGAUUAUAGUGCCAAAAAUAGUUAAAGUGCCUUGGUCCUCCCUCUGUAGGCAGCAAAUUGAAACUAACAUGGGACCAUGCCAUCCUUCUAGCAUAAUGGAGAAGUCUGAACUGAGGAGUAUCUUUGAUGAAAGACAUUUAGGACCCUAGAAACUAAAUCUUGUCACCAAGACUUUAUAGUAAAGUAGUAGCAAAAUUAUUUUUAAAAGACUUUCUUCCUUUUACUACCCAUUUCCUCUCUUGGGAAAGCUGAUGAGCAAAUUAUCCAAGACUCAUUUCUUUAUUAGGCAAAGUCAGAAUAUUUCCCCUCUGAAAAUCUGAAUUAUGCCCUCAUUCUUUUUCAAGAAAUAUCUCAAAGAGCAAAUAGAAUUAAACAUGACACUUGAUUGUCUGAUUAUUUGGCAUGUAUAAAAUUAUCAUGUGGCUUAAUGUGCCUUAAGUGAAAAUUUAAACUUAGACCUGAAACCUUUACAGUUGGAUGUAGCGUUGAGCUUUUGCAUGUUUUCUGUAUAAUAAACCACUUUUGUUUUGUUUGUUUUGUCUUUUAACCUACACCUUUAUCAUUACUCUAACAGAUUUAGGGCUUCUCUUUCUCUACAGCUAAGUAAGGGAAUAUGUGCAAUUAUGAGACAUACAAAAAAGGAAAGGGAAAGGACUUUCUAAGUAGCAAAUCUGUGCCAUGAAGUAGAUGUGGCGUGAAGAUACAGAGCCUGAGGAUAGUAAUUUUCCCUGAGCCACGCACACAGGCUUUUAUUUCAUGCCUUUUCUCUUUCUGUGCCGUCACCUUUGAGAAAAACGAUUGCACCUUCUCCAAGUCUGCCUUUUUAACAGCUACAGUUAAGUUGGCAAGACUUCCCCAGCUCUGAAUAUAGCCAUUUGCCGACUCCGGCCUCUUUGCGAGACUGACUCAAAUCUGUGAUCUUCUGUUCAGCAUACACAUCAGCAAAGUGAGAAGAUGAGCACUAAAUAUAGGCUCUAUUAACUUUACUUUUAGAUUUACUGCCUUCAAAAAGUGCCUAUUCUGAGCAACAUAAACGUUAUUCCUUACAUAUGUAUGUACACACGGUACCCAGAGUCGUACUGUGCAGCCUUCAAAAACAUACCAUCAGAAAGAGUAGGUGCUGAGAUAAGGAAACUUUGCCAAAUGAAAGAAAGUCACUCACUUCCAAUAUCCCCUCUCAAGCGGCUACCGUGAAACGGGCUGCAAACACAUUCCCUGAGCAUCCCUUGCUGAUACAGCUUCUUUAUAUUUAUAUCCUACUGGAUGGUAGCAUAUUGCUAAGGUUUCCUGUACUCUGCUUCAAGGGAAUGUAAGCUUUAUGGCAUUGAAACAUUUAGGGAAAAAAAAGAUGUUUAAGAGAAUUAAUAGAGCCGUAGUCUGUAUUAGGAUGUGUGUCAUAUGUGUGUUCUAUAAACUAAGCAUCGGUGGGUUUAGAGUGUUAAAGUGUCAGCACAUUCCUUCUCCUUUUGUCUCUCAGGCUAACAUGAGAGAAAAUAGAAAAGUCUUGGCUGUGGGGAUUGGAAGCUCAGGGGGCCAAAUGUCCUUGCCAGAUCCUUAGAGCAUUACUUUGACUCCUAAAAAUAGUAGUGUAUGUUAUUUGAUGGCUUUUGUUUCCAUAGUUCCAUCACUGACAAAACUGUCAAUACUGUUGAUGGAGCAGCAGCAUAGCCUAGAGUGAUGCAUUCUUACCCAGAGGUGGCAAUAGGAGAGGGUCCAUGUAAAUAGGACGAGGUAGACAGUGCAUGAUUGUAGGAGAAGGGUUGAAGGGAGGACAUGAUUCCAAAAAAGAUCGUUCUCAAUGUGUCGUCUGACUCAACCAGCUGGCAGAUUACACUUGCCAAGUCGUUCCCUUUCCUUCUAAGUCAGUUGGCUCCAUAUUCACUUGAAUAUGCCUCUGUUUGGGCAAAGCAAGAUACCUCCACUUAACCUUUAUCCAAGGAAGCUCUUGGUGUCCUCUUGGUCAUAAAGUUGUCUCCUACCUAACCCAGUUUUACCAAAUGGAAGUAAAAGGGGACAAACUAUGGAAGAUGGACUCCAUGCCAUUGCAGUCAGCCACCAUUCUCUUUUCCAUAUAAGGAGCCCCAUUACAUAAGCUACGGGUGAGGUUGGAACAGCUAUGUUUCAUAAUUUCAAGAGUGUGACCACCCUGCUCUAGUCAUCAUCAUUGGAUGAAUCCAGUUGACUCUUUGGCAAAAGGGUGAUACUUUUCACUAAAAAUGCCUACUCUUCCUGUUGAUGUUCCUUUUCUGUUUUUACCUUGUCCAAUUUCCACACUAGUCAUUUUUUUUAUUUUUUAGAGGAUCAGAUUUUAGCGCUGGAAAAUGAGUUCAAAAAUUUCAGUGUAAUGUCAUAAGGAUGUUGGGAUACAGAGAUUUUUUUUUUCCUUGGAAACAAAUGGACUGGGAAGAAACACAGCAUGGCUUUGCUCUGAGUUUCAAUCUGAUGAUUAUGACCAUGGAAGAUAGUCUUAUGUAAAGGUUAAAUGGUGUUUACAAGUGGAUAGAUAAGGCGGAGAUGGUGAGAAGCCGGGUUUUCUCUAUGCUAAAUGUGUCUACUAAGAGCAGCACUUCCUACUAGCUAAGCACAAUCAUAGCCCCACCGUGAUGAGCUGCUAGUCUGAAUAACAUUCCCUGACUUAGGGAAAGGCACACAAAAACAUAUAAAGAAUAUGUCUAUUUUCAUAUGUGUGAUACUGACAGAGCCAUGGUAUUCCUAAAAUAUAGGUUUCUCUUUUUUCUUGUAUUCUUAGCAAAUUGCAUUUAUUCACUACAUUACAAACCAUCACUGAUGUAUCCAAAAUAGCACACAUAGUUCAGUAUGAAAAUAAGAGAAUAAAAUCUGUUAUAAGCAAGUGAUUUAGGUAUUUUCUUUUGUGUUUAUGCAUUAUCUGACUAUAUUAAAACCUGUUUUUCUAUUUACCUUCUAUCAGUUUUCUCUACCAAUUAUGUUUUUUCAAUGCUCUAUAAGAAUGAAUAUGGAAAUUAUAUUUCUUUUUUCUGUAAAAGAGUUGCAACUACUUUAUUAUAUUUAGAAAUCCAAUAAACUUCUUAUUACAUUUA